GUCUUUAUUACUCACCCCAUGCCCCUUAAGAAUGCCAGUAAAUGUCAUGGUACUUGGCAGACACUGGCCUGAAAUGACAGUGGUUUGUGUACCCUGAGAUUUUUGAUGCUGCAGUAUUGGUAAUGAAAGUUCAUCUUUGAUUGUAGUUGGGAAAGUGGGACCUAGAAGGGUAGGUGUGGUUAUUCAUUGCUAGGAUUUAAGCUCUUUGCCUUUUGGCUGUCUUGUUUCUUCCCUCCACCACAACAAUCAUUCUCUCUGCCCACAUUCUGGGGGCAGAACAGGGAUAUCCCUUUGCUGGUGGUCGUGGCAGCUGGGAAACAGGACCUCUUAGUUUUCCAUGCAUGUCUAUAUCCAGGCUAAGUCAAAUGAGGAUGGCAAGUGCGUGCUACUGUUGUGUAAUCUCUAUUUGUGUAGUGUUUAUUCAUGUAUGUAUUUGCUCUUAGAAUAAUACUCAGAGGUAUUUCUCUGAUUAUGUAAUGUGUGUGUGUGUGUGUGUGUGUGUGUGUGUGUUUUUAAAUUAAAAGUCCUGUUUUACUUCUGGCCAUUCUGUUGCAUAGGCAUAGGGCUUUUAGCAAUUUAUUCACCCAUCCAUUUAUUCAACAAAUAUUUAUUCAGCACCUUCCAUGGCCAGGCAUCAUGCCAGGUAUUGGAUAUUCUGCUGUGAACAAACACAUCCACAUGGAGCUAAAUGUCUAGUGAGUAGGCAAACGAGAAAGAAUCAUGGGAUAUACAUUCAACUGCGCAUUGUGGAAAGUGCUAAGAGGAAGGGGGCACAGAGUUUAGACAAGGUACAAGGAAGGACCUCUAAAAAAGUGGUGCGAGAGCUGUGAGCUGGAGAGGAGAGAGGAGUUGACCAAAAAAGCAGAGAUCCAGGGGUCUUGUGGGUCUGGCUGGAAAAUUUGGAUUUUUAAAUAAGGGGAAAUAUUGAAGGGUGUGAAGCAGAGGGAGUGACAUGAUGUGACUGAGAAAUCAAGUCAGUUUAUGUGUUCGUUUACUUUUUUAUGAUAUGGGACAACUAUUUUGCUCUUACUUAACCAGUAAAUAGUAUGAUGGUGGUGGUGGUGACGGUGUGGAUACUGGUGCCUAAUAGGAAAUAUUUUGUUAGCUGCAUGUUUUAAAUUUAGCAACAUUACUAUGGAAAACUCUUCAUGAUGGUUUUCCCUUCUCAGAUUAUGCUUUAUUGAAAUGUCCUUUUUUGGAUAUUUUACUUUUAAAAAGUAACUGAAAAUCACUUUAUUCCAGCUGGCCUAUUUCCGAAUGGAAAAUAUUAGUGGUCUUUGAUAGUUUAGAGAAACAUGAGGGCCAUUUAAUGUCAUUGCUACAACCAGGCUGCUCUUCACCGUGUUUGGGCUGCUGUGGCUCUACUGGUUGAUAAAAUAUUGAAACACUUUCUUAUCAGUUGAUGAAUAAUACAACAGUAACCGUGAGAAGUGGUAAAACUAACAAUAUAAUUUUCAACAUAAACUCAUUCACCCUAGCUGAUUUUGUAGGAUGUGCUGGGGUCCACUUUGGAAGCGCUCACUGUCUGUCUGCCGAGCCUGUGUCUCAUGGCAGUGAGUGGCGUUGAUCUCCUGCACGUUCAUGAUGGAGCUGGGGCCUCGGUGCUUCGGGAGAGUCAUCACCUUAUCAUCAGCCUCAGACUUUUGCAUUGCUCCUGCUUUUAAUAACUGAGUUUUAAAUAGGUCUUUCUUUGGUUUCUUUCAUUGUUACUGCAUUAUAACUCUUGGAUUGGUCGUGUGUGGUGUUUCAUACUUAGAAGUUCAAUAAUUAAUUUGUUGAGUAUUUUAUUUUAAAUAAAGAGGCAAUGAAGUUUGGGAAGGUUUUCUUUUUUUAGAUGUCAUAAACAUGAAUAUUCUGAAUCUCUGAGAGAAGAAAAAAAUAACAGUAAUAAAACACAGUUAAGAAUAUCUUUAAUACUGUGCAGGAAUAUAAACCUGAAACAAAUGAUUUGUAGGUCUAGAAUCAAGAACAAUUUGAUUAUUUCAACAAAAAAUAAUAAACAUAAAUCAUUUUCCAAAAAAUUGAAAUAACAACAUCGAAAAACAUUUUAUCUGAGAGUUUUGACAAGGCAAAGGAAAAAAAAUUUACGAAGUAUCAAUAUAAUAUACUGUAUAGUUUAAAAUAAUUUUCUGACAUUAAGUAUUUAUUAGGACUUCAAGAAUUGUUUUUAUGUGAAUGUAGCAUGGAAGUUUGGGUUUAUGGUCCUGAUCGUUGCAAAACAUAUAUCUACUGAGAUGCAAAAAUGCAUUUUGGAGAACUUAUAAAUCAGGAAGGUAAAAUUUCAGUCAUUAUUGACAUGGCUCCAACAAUUUCACAUAGAAAUGUUUUAAUAAUUUACUUAAAAUGCAAUAUUCAAGACUUCAAAGACAGUGUGAUGGUUUUUAUUGAUUUCAUGAAGCUGGAAGGAACAACAUCUGAAAUAUAUUAAACUUUAUUAGUCAUACUCAAGAAAAAUGGUUUCAAUGAGAAAUACUUACAUGAAAACCUUGUGAAUGUUUCACAGAUGGUGCAAGUAUAGUGUUAGGGAGAAAAAGUUGUCUUAGCUGAAAUUCUAGAAAAACUUCUAGGUGUUUUCAUUUGAUGCUGUCUCACUUAUAUUUGGUUAUCUCUGGAUGAUGCAAUAGGAAGAUAAGCCAAGUAAACCACUUAACUUUUUUUUUGGAAAUUUUACAUUUAUCUUGUAUCAAAUAAAUACUAGAGAAUUAAAUAACAUAUUUGAGACCUUGGAAUUGAGAUGACUGUUUGGACCUUUAACGGUCAGCCGAAGAUGGGAAUAUUCAUGUUAAUGGACAUUGUUAAAAUAGCAUUUGGACAAUUUUUUUAGCAGUUUGGCUCUAUUACAUGAUAUACUAACCAAUGUGAAUUUUUCCAUGGUUUUAGAAAAAAGAAAAAUUUUAAUUAUUAAAAUGGACAGAUUUAUUUGACAAAUACUAAGUGAUAGAAUAUAUAAACCAAAUACAGGAAACUGUGAUGGAGAAGAAGGUAUUAGAGGAACAAACAAAUUUGAAAUGAAACAAAAUAUUAAUUCCAAGGGAAAAACUCUUACAUUGCCUGGCAAAUUAAAAGAAAAUGCACUUAUUUGGUGACAAAUCUAAGGAAUACAAUUAAAUUUUAAUAACAUCCUUUUAAUUUAUUGAUUCUGAGAACUUGGCUAAUUGUUGUUUUCAAAGCACCAUAGAUUGAAGGCAAACAAAAUUUUGUAUAAUUAAGCCAGAAAUGAAACAGAACAAUCCAAUAAAUAAGGGAUUUUCAUAAGGCUUGGAUGGUAAUAGAAAUAGUGAAUAUAAAAUCUCAGUAUUAUUAGGGCUGAAAAAAUAGAAUUUAACUAAUAUUAGUUCAGUAGAAGGUAAUGGAAGAUUUACUAUGAGCAGUAUUAUGUGAUGGGAAAAUCUGUAUAUAUUAAGACUUGGUUUGCCCAUUGUUUUAAAUUAAAUGGGGGAAAUUAUUGAAAGAAUUUGGUUUCGUAUAUCAAUCACAGCUCAUAUAUUGCUUAGCUUGUGACAGAUACAUCAAAUAAAAAGAUCAUACCAGUAAUUUGUAACAAUUAACAGAUGACUUGGAAAUGAGUCACAUGAUUUGAUGAAUGGUUGCUGUUAGAACUUACUUCACCUGGGAUACGGUUUCAUAAAAUGUGUAAUUCAUAUUAUUUAGAGAACAAAUGGAAUAUUUUACAAUUUUUUAUUUAUAUGGCUAUUUUUUUAUUAAAAGGCUGGUUGUUAAAUAAUAUCACUCCUGACAUGAAUAACUUUAAUAAGUAUAUCUGUGAUUAGGUGAUUAUCCUAUUAUAUGUUUUACAUAGAGUGAGUUUUAGAUCAAGAAUUGGCUGUUACUAACCCUCUAUUACAUUUCCAUUAAUUUUGACUAAUCAGUACUUUUCUGUAAAAUUUGAUUAAUCAAUACUUUUAUGUUUUUAUGUAGUUCUUUUGGUAAUUCUGUCGUUGCAAAUAAUGUAAGUAUAGUAAUUUGUGAGCUGUUCUUUUUCCUUCUUAUUUUUGGUUUAGUUUUUCACUUCUGUUACUCACAAAGCAAACAUUAGGCUCUCUUAUUUAAAUACAUUUUCUUUCAAACCACCUAAGUAAAAUGUUGAGCUUUUUGCUGCUGUAUUUAAGCCAGGCAGUGUUACUUUCACUGAUUUAAGAUCUGAAGCAGCAUACCUACUUAUCAUCAUUUCAUUAUACAGAUUUGUGUAAGAGUGUUUAAAGUAGGUUUUAAGAUACAGUAUGUUUAAAAUUAAAAUUUGAGGUAUGAUUUGCAGUGUCCACUGAAUACUUCAAGAAAGUAGAAGAGUUGCUUCAUUAUAUCACAGUUUUGUUAGUUUCAGCAAUUAAUCUAGUUUGACAUUAGCAUUUUUGUUUUUCUGUAAUCUUUUUUUUUCUAGCAUAUGUAGUUUCAUCUUUUCAAGGACCAACAACUAAUUUUGUGUGUAUGUAUUGAUACUUAACAUAAAUUGCUGCUUUGCUGUGUGGUCUGGGUAGAAUUAUUCAUUGUUUUCUAGCAAAAAGGGACAUUUGUCUCUUUUUUCCUGCAUGUAUUAUGUGGUUGGGAGAAUAAUUUCUGUCCCCAUUCUCCCAAGAUGCUCAUACAUUAAUCACUGGAAUCUGUGAAUAUAUUACCUUACAUGGCAAAAGGGAUUUUGCAGGUGGAAUUAAGGUCAUGAGACUUAAAAUAGGGAGAUUAUCCUGGAUUAUCUGGGUGGGCCCAUUGUAAUCACAAGCAUCCUUAAUAGUGAAAGGGGAAUGGAGAAGACUCAUGAGAUGUGAGGGAAGAAGGAGCAGGAGAGAUUUGGAGCAUGAGAGGGACUCCACCUGCUGCUUCUGGAUCUGAAGAAGAGGGGACUAUGAGCCAAGGAGUGCAGGUGGCUUCUAGAAGCUGAGAACAGCCCUGGCAGCUGUCCAGCAAGGAAACAAGGGCUUCAGUCCUGUAAUCACAUGGAACUCAAUCCUGCCAGGUCCCUGAAUGUCCCUGAAAACAGAUUAUUCCCUAGAACCUCCAUAGAUGCUGCCCUGUCAGCCCCUUGAUUUUGGCCUUGUAAGACUCAGGCAGAGAAAUCAGCCAAGCCUGCUGAACUUCUGGCAAACAGAUCUGUGACAUAAUACAUUAGUGUUGUUUUUAGCUGCUAAGUUUUGUGGUAAUUUGUUAUAACCACAAGAGAAAACUUAUACAUACUAUUUUAUGGAAAAUCAAAUGCAAAAUACCUCACAUUACUGAGCAGCUCUUAAUCUCGUGGUGGGGGAAAUGAAAGGUUGGGGAAGAGAUGAAAGAAUUGAGAGGCAGGGAAUGAGGUUUUUUGUUUCUUUUAAAAUUCUUUUGGAUGGAGCAUUAGAGCAGGAAAGCUUGACUCUAGCACUCAGUAACUUAAUUAUCUGUGUAAUUAUCUGCAUUACUGAUAUACAGUAAUUACAAUUUUGACUUGAUGCAUGUAUUCGUUGGAAAAAUAAUUUAAUUUGUGUUGUCCUUAAAGCAUAAUUUUAUUAGAGUUGCUUUUAACAUGUCAGUGCGGAAAGAAUAGUUCUAUCUGCAUUUAUAAUUAUGCUUCUACUCAAACUUAUUUGAAUUAUGACCCUGAUUCAGGCACUUGCAGCCCAUCUUUUCAUGGAGGAAAAGAAUCUUCUGCUGCAAAUUAAAAAAACAAACAUGGAGCAUUAAAGUUCGAAGGAACUUUAUUCAAACUGACUGCUCAUUCAACAAAUGAAGGAGUUAAAAAGUUCAAGGAAGCUCAGUAUGUUGACCUAAGUCACUAAGCCAGGUGCGCUACCCAGGACCCAAGAAUGUUGGUCUGUUGCUGCAGAUGGCAGGUAGAAAAUAUUCUGAAGGAUAAGACCAAAGCUGGGUUCUGCUCCUCAUUUUUCCACGUUUCUAUACUGUGAAUUGGGAAAUUUAUUCAUCUCCAAACUAGAAUGCUGCAACCCUAAAAUAAGUGAAUAUGAUAUUUGCCAAUAAAAAUGGAAGUUGCCUUGUAGACCUACAAGGGACAAGUUUGUACAUUAUUUAAGUAUCAGUGUUAGGAUAAGCUGUCAGUCUAAAAUCAGGUGCUCUGUAGAAAGAGCCUGUUCUACAAAAGCAAAAAUAAUGGAGGCUUGACUUUUAAGUAGUUUGGUUGUAGGGGUAGUUAUGACCGCUUGUAGUAGAGAAUAUAUCAGGAUAAGUUCUGUAUAGCUGAAAAGAAGUCACAGACUUCAAGGGAGGAUCAUUGAGGUACCAGUGGCUGACUUGGAAUGGUUGUGGCCUGUUUUGUUACACCUUUUGCUUUUCACGUUAAAGUGCGUGAUUGGCCUUAACUUUUCUGAAAAAGUACUUUAUCCUCUUUGAAGUCCUCCCAUUGCUGACUGAUUCACAGAGAUACCUAUUUAUAAGCUCUUUGUUGAUCAUAACCGUGUUCCAGGGGAGGCACGAAUGAGUGGCUUCAGGAAGAUUUGGUUUUGUUUUAUUGAAGUUAGAGGUGAUGGAGGGCAGCCUAGGUUUGGGAGCUCUCAGAUAGGCAGCUCCCUUCUGGUUCACACUGUGCUCAUUCUGCUGCCAGGUGAGCCCUGCAGGAUCGCCGUGCUCUUCUCUGUGCUCCGCAGGUGGCCACGUUUUCUCUGGCCUGUGGACCUUCGCAGGGGGCGUUGUCGUUGCCCAGGAUGAUCUUCAGCCUGGUGUACUAGCCCUCAAUAUCAGUAUUCGGAAAAGUUGGCCCAGCUGCCAUUUCCUCCUUGGACGUCUCCCCUCACUCCCAGCCUCAGUGAGAAGUCUUUCUGUGAACUCCUAGAAUGCCUCUUGUAAAUCCCCACAAGUGCUCUGACGCUGCAUUGGAAUUGGCUGACUUCUCGUGUCUUCCUGGACGGCAGGCUCCUUGAAGGCAGAUACUAUCUUUCAUUUCUGUACUCCCAUUGCCAAGCACACUUUGUUGAAUGAGUAACCAAAUAGUGUGACCUGCUUUGGGACAGUCACUUGUUCUAAUGGGUCAAUAACUAAUGGAUUGGUAUUCUGCAAACCCACAGGCACAUGCAUAGAUAGUUUAUGUAUCAGGUGUGCUUGGUAAAUUUUGUUCAGGUUAGUUCUGGAAUCUUGGAUUAUACUAUGAAUAUUGCUUUCUAUCCUUUUUUCCGUCUCUUAUGUUACGACAUUUCCCUGUAUCAUAAAAUGACCAUUGAAAACUUGGUUUUUAGCCACUGCAUAGUAUUUCAUUAUGUUAAUGUAUUCAGUGUGUUAACAUUAAAAUUUAACCCUUCUAUUGUCGUUUCUAAAUUUUUCUAUUAUAAAUAGCAUCAUGAUAAGCAGCUUUGCAUAAAAACUUGUGUGUAUCUCUGGUCUUUUUUCCUUCUCAUUUCAGGCAUAGCAUUUGUUUUUGAGAGUUUUAAGAUGUAAUGGUUGAUUAUAUAUUUUUUAAAUUAUGAAAAGCAGAACUGAGUGAAAGUGUGGGCUUUCAAAUGUAGAUUUUUUGAAUGUUUAGUUUCCCUGUUUAAUAUCUGUAGGCUCUUGGGCAAAAGAUGCCUUUUUGUGGCUCAUCUUUCACUUUAUAAAAUAGGGAUUUAGGCUGGUCGCAGUGGCUCAUGUCUGUAAUCCCAGCACUUUAGAAGGCUGAGACAGGUGGAUCACCUGAGGUCAGGAGUUCGAGACCAGCCUGACCAAUAUGGUGAAACCCCGUCUCUACUAAAAAUAGAAAAAUCAGCCGGGUGUGGUGGCCUGUGCCUGUAGUCCCAGCUACUGGGGAGGCUGAGACAGGAGACAGCUUGAUCCCGGGUUGUGGAGGUUGCAGUGAGUCAAGAUCUCGCCACUGCACUCCAGCCUGGGUGACAGAACGAAACUCUGUCUCAAAGAAAAUAAAAUAAAACAGGGAUUUAUAUCAGUCAGUUGAGACCAGGUUAUUGUACAGUAACAACUCUGAAAUCUCAGUGAGUUGACAGCAAUAAAGCAUGUUUACUACUCAGUUUUUGUCCAUCAUGGGUUAACUUGGGGGCUGUGUUCCUUGUGGAAAUUCAGGAAGCCACACUGAUGGAGGUUCCAUCUUGAUGUAUACUUCAAAGAUUAUGUAGGACGAGGUAAGAGAGAGAACAUAGCUCUUCAAGCUUCCGCCUGGAAGUGACAUGCUUUUGUUGCACUGGCUAAAGCAACUUUCAUGGCUCUCUGCCUGAUUUCACAGGUUGGGAAUGUAUAAUCCCUGCUGGUAGUAAUAAAGUCUGCCUCCAGCUAGUGACUCAGGAUGGGAAACACCUGGAACGCAUCAUAUGCCUACUACGUGGUAGCAGUUGAUUAAUGUUAGCUAAUAUUAAUGCUGGUUUCUCUGGGAAGUAUUAAUGACCUGUUAUAAAAGUUAUACAUAGGUGUAGGAUAUGAUGAAACCUAACAUUUGUACUUACUUAUUGGCAGUUUAAUUAUAUUAAAAACUUAGCUAAAAUGCAUUGAUAGAUUAAAAAUUAAAACUGCAUCAUCAUAAUUUGAAUAUAGAUUUUCUCUAUAAACUUUACAAUUUAAAUGUAUCUUUGUUUUUGUUUUUAAAUCACAGCAGUGAAGGUUUAACAAUGAACAGUUUCUAAAUUAGUUGAAUAUACUAACUUUGAAAGCCAGUGCCUUUCGUCACAGGAGAAUGUACUUACCAAUUACAACAUUUUGAUAAGGCAUUCUUAUGUGAAAAUGCAUCUGAUCUAAAUCAGUUUUGCAUUCUCUGGUCUGCUAACAUUAGUUUCAUUUCUUGCAUUUUGAACAAAGAGUUGUGUAUUUUUUUCGAAUUAGAGUUGGACCUCUAAAUUGAGGUUUCAUAUGAAUAGUUAUAUUUAAAAAAAAUCUCUUCAAGUCAUUCUGUAGUACUUGAUUGAAAUCAUGAACAUGACAUACCACUUCAUCAGCAGUUUUUCCCAGCAUUAAAUUAUUUUAUUAUUUUACUCUAGUGUCACAAAUCUAAGAAUGUCAUUUCUAAAAAUUUCUAAAAUAGCAUUGAUAAUUAAGUCUUACAAGUUAGGUAGACUGAAUGUUAAAUUUGGUUCUCUUAAAAUGCAGAAGAAUGAGAAUUCUGAUAAGCAGAUCUUACCCAGCAUUUUUUAUUUUAAGAAGAUUUUCUUUAAAGUACACAAAACAUACAUGUAGAGUUUGAUGAAUUUUCAUAAAGUGAACACAUCCAUUUCUACAGUACCCAAGUCAAGUAACAGGACAUUAUCAAUACCCUCAAAGACCCCCUUGCUCCCAGUUACUCUCCCACCCCCAAGCAGUAACAGAUAACCCCCAUCCUGACCAAACACCACAGAUUAGUUUUGGUACUUUGUACAGUUGGAUCUAUAGUAUAGACUUUUUGUUGCUGACUACUUUCAUGUAUCAUUAUAUUUGUGAGCGAAAUAACCUCUGUUGGAUAUCAUAAUUGUUCAUUGCUAUAUAAUAUUCCAUUGUGUGAAUAUUCAUUCUGUUAGCCAAUAUGCUUUAACAUUUUGAUAACACUAAGACCUGUUAAGUUUUUGCAAAUUAUUAAAGGUAUUUUAACUUAGUUUAGGAUGUAAAGUCAAAAAAUAUGGAAGUCAAUAAAAGCUACCAGUGGUCACAUUUAUAACUUGCAGCAAUUUGAAUUGUAGUUAUUUGUUGCAUAAGUAAAAAUGUGUCCUCACUUAGAAAAUUGGUUAGUCUGCUAAAACAGUAAUGAUUUUACAGAAUUGAAUAUUUGGAGGAUGAACUCUAUGGUAAACUCUGGAUUUUAUUCUGAAAGGUGAGUGACAGUCCCCGAUGCCACCCCUUUUGUGAAAUCUGUGGUGUUCUCUAGUGUGCCCUUUCCCUACCUUGCAUUGGACUUGGUCCUGACAAGUCUCUGUUCCCAGCAGAUUGUGAGGUCCUGGACAGCAGGACCCACUCUUAUAGGCAGGUACCCAGAGAAGAAAGGCCACAUAACUGAUGGAAUGAAUGAGCAACACCCAGCUAGGACUCUUAGAAUCUGUUGCUUUUUAGGUAAUUUCAUGAAGUGCAAAGCAGUUUAAUAACUUUUGACCAGAGACAGAUGGAAGUUUUUAGUGUUACAGUAAAAUUGGUUGAAAUAUUUUCUUCUCAUUUGUGAAAGUUCAUCUUUACCUAACACUCGAGUAGAAUCCUCAGGUGGGAAAAUGCAGUGUGGCUGACUGGCAGCAGCAAUGAACCACACAGUGAUACCGGGUGGAGUCCAGGCCACAAAGACUGUAACUGCUGUGGAAGGGUUGCCUGCCUGGGCACCUCAAAAGGAGAAGGGCAGCAGGUUCAGAUCAGGUUGUCUGCAGCCAGCUGCUGGAAGGGUAUUUGCCCAAAGGGUGUUGCUAGUACCCAUGAGGAACUCCUUCCAUUCCUUGCCCACCUUCUGAGCCUGUGAGAUUAGACAGAGGCAGUGUAAAUUCCUCUAGUGAAGUUGCUGUGCCACUAGCAACUUCAAAAUCUGGCAAUCUAAACUAUAAUUUUGAGAACUUUGUACUUGAGCUAUAAUACAAAAUCAUUUUUAGUAAGUUUUGCUCUAGUUAACUACCUUUGUUUUUGUUUUUAAAGAAAAGAUUUUAUUUUUAUUUUUGAGACAGAGUGUCGCUCUGUCACCCAGGCUGUACUCACACUGCACACCCAGGAGUGCAGUGGUGUGAUCUCGGCUCACUGCAACCUCUGUCACCCAGGGUCAAGUGAUUCUUCUGCCUCAGCCUCCCAAGUAGCUGGAAUUACAGGCACAUGCCACCACCCCCAGCCAAUUUUUGUAUUUUUAGUAGAGACCGGGUUUCGCCAUGUUGGCCAGGCUGGUCUUGAACUGCUGACCUCAAGUGAUCCACCUGCCUCGGCCUCCCAAAGUGCUGGGAUUACAGGUGUGAGCCACCGCACUUGGCCAAGAUUUUUAUUUUUGAUUAAUGAGAAGUUACUGUUGUUUUUGAAAAAUGGAAUAAAGUUUUUAGCACCAAUUUACUGAAAUUUCUUGCAUUUUGUCUUUUGUUACACUGAUACCUUUCUAGUGUACAUUCCCUGUUCAUCAUUUUCUAAAGUCGAGUCGUGUUAAACUGGGUUAAAGGAGGGAAACAUGAAAAGGUUUAGGAAUAUUAUUUCUAAUUAAAGGUUGAGAGUUUCUCAACCUCAGCACCAUUGGCAGUUUGGGCCAGAUAAUCUUUGUUGUGGGGCCCGUGCUGUGCCUUUUAGGAUGUUUAGCAGCAUCUAUGGCCUUUACCCACUCGACACCAGUACCAUCUCCUGUGCCCUCGUAUGAUUACCAAAAGAUGUCUUCAGAUGUUACUGGAUGUCCCCUGGAGGGCUACUGAUUUAGGCUAUUAAGCUCUAAUUAGUAUGGAAUCUGGUUAAUAGUACAGGCUCUGAAGUCAAAUUCCUUGGAUUGAAAUUCUAACUCUUCUUUGGCCAAGUGACAACCACUCUGACCCGCAGUUUUCUCAUCGCUCACGUUGGGGACUAUAAUGUUACUCAACUCAUAGAUUAGAAUGAAUGAGUUAAUACAUGUAAAUCUUUAAGAAUGGCACCUGGUGUGUUGUAAAUGCUCAACAAAUGUUAACCAAUAUUACUGUUUUUAUUUGUAAGAACAUUGGGUAUUAUAGUACAUCUUUUCUUCUUAUUUUUCACCAUGUCACAGAAUGGAGACCUAAGGGGUAAUAAUAAGUGAGAAAAUUUCUUAACAAAUUAUUCUUCAUUUUAAAAAGCUGCAUUGCUGUAUCCUCUGGCAGGCAGUGUGGCAAAGUGAAUGCAUAUCUGACUCUUCCGACAAGUUCCUUUGCCUUCAGUAACUCUGUGCUGCUUAGCAGAAACCAUUGCUUUAAAUCAGGCUUUGUGGAAAUAGAGGGAGAUGACUUACAAAUUGACUUUCAAUAUGGGGUUAAUCCAUCUUUGUUCUGGAUUAAGAAAGGCUGGUCUCAGUCCUCUGAGCCUCUGUCUUCCCAGAGUUGGAGGCACAUUUCAAGACCGUCUGUCCCCAGCCCAAGACAGAGGGUAGUGAGAUGCCCCCAGAUGGGAGUAUGGGCUGGAAGAAAUGCUGAUUUUCUCUAUUACCUCGAUCAGUUGAAGCUACCUCCUCCUUGAAUUUAACCCAUUAUCUGAUUUGACAAGAAUUUAUUUUGCUAAAACCCUGAUUGUGGCCAUGAUUGCUAAUUUCAAAGAAUAAAAAAAAUGCAGGGAAGUUGGGGAGGGAAGGGCCUACAGAAGGAAUAGCAGAGAUUGGACAGAAGGGAAAUAUUGUUUCCUAAAACCUGACAAUGGGAAAGGAAAAAGAGAAGAAGCUGCAAGCAAAUACUUAGUCAUACAUACCAAAAUAGACUUGAAAUAAUUUAAAUCAGCCAAAUACCUCCACUAGUGAUACAUGCAACUGAAUUACAUUGACCAGUUUAUAGGUUUAAAAAAUCCAUAUGAGUUAAUCUCAAAUAUGUUAAUGACCAAUAUUUUAAAAUUUUAUCAAGUUUCUGACUUUUAAAACACGCUUCUGAUAAAGAAUUGGAAUUUUUAAUGUAGAAAAAAUGUUUUAAGUUAAUGUGAGAUUUUUAAAGGGAAGUCAGCCUCCUUUUUUGCCAAAAUAAAGGAGUAUAUAAUUUGCCCCAGUUAUGAUGCCAUUUUCCUAGAAUGUUAGGAAGAUUCUGAUUCCUCCUGUUCACUUUUCCCAAUGUGAAAACUGAGACCUAGAGUUACAGGACCUUUCUAGGAUUGCUUAGCUAGCUUGAGCCUUGAGCUCUUGUUAAUUUUUUCAUUGUUGGGGGGUCUUAAUUUGGCUUAAGAAGUUGAUACAAGUCUUUUACAACGUUGUUCUUUUUUUAAAUCUAGUAAUUGUUUCUGAACUUUAUGGACUUGUACGUCGUAGGAAGCACUGAUAAAAAUGCAGCUGAGUGUCAGAUGCUUUUAUUACCUGGAAGCUGGGGCCCUGACUAUGAAUACACAGUUUACUUCCCACUCGGGCAGCAAGUUUCCUGGCAUGUGUCUGCCUCUCUCCCUGCAGGCUCAGGUGCCCCUGUUCCUGUCGUCAGCAUCCGGCCCUGCACUGCUGUUGCCCUCUGAAUCUCCUCUGUCUUUCCUGUCUUUGGCUGUGGUCUCUUCACUACCUACCCUGUCCAAUCUAAGUGAGAAAGCUGCAUCACGCUUAAGGUUUUCUUUCCUUAAUACCAGGCCCCACUGCCCCAGUGAGUGCCCAGAUCCUGCAGAAUCUGCUUCUUCACCAGUCGCCAUCCCUAGCAUGGACAUUUGCAGUGGACAUUUGUGAAUGGACUGAUGGAUGAGCCACUGAUAGUGUUCCCUUCACUGCAGGCCUUAGUAUAUUCAUGCCUGUUAGAUGUGACACUUAAGUGCUAAAUAUACUUUGAAGGUAAUGUGGAACCCUCUCUCCAUCACAUGAAGCAUGUCUGCUCAGGGGCAUCCCUUCACCCCGCUGAAAAGCUUGAAUAAUUCUCCAUGGUAACUGGAUAAGGCAGCCCUGGAUAAGGCAGCCCCACGUCCAGAGACUGGCACAUGAAGUCUUUCACAGAAUGCCCCCCGCCCCGCCCAUACCCUUCUAGCCUCCUUUCCACCAGUGCCCAUUCCUCUGCCUCAAAAUUCAGUCAAUGGAGAAUUGUAAAAGAUUAGUACAUUUAGGAUCUUGUCUUUUAUGUAAGUGAAAAUAAGGACCGAGUGUUGAUGCUUUGGAUUCAAGAGCCAGCUGUGCAAAAUUAAAGUAUCCUAUUAUUCACUGUGUGUAAUGAUGACCCUAAUGAAUGUGGGAUAAUUCACUUCCCAUUGAUGAGAAUUCAGUCUAAAACUGUAAACUAGAUGCUCAUUAAUUUAAUGCUUUUCCUUGACACAUGUUUUGUUUCUACAGCUGUUAGUGAAAUGUUUUUAGGCAUCUGUGCAGGUGGAAGGAUGCAUGCAAGCUAAAUAAGUCUAGAGGACGAAGAGAAUCUCUUUGGUAUUCCUUAUAACCAUCCUUCUAAAAGGGGAUCCCCAACCCCCUUCAAAAGCAUGCUUCUGGAAGUCUCUUGUGGCUCAGUCUCUACCCUGUUUACUUGUCAUAUUGUGUCUUUAUGUCUGCUUCUCACCAUUUUGCCAUUCUCAUUUUCUAGUAGGGACGUGGGCAUGGAGAGACAAAACACCGGAACUGCCAGGAGAGAGCAGAGCUUCCCCUUCCUGUGAGCAGCCCUGGGUGGUCCUACCCCCUCCCCUCACAGCUGGUUUGAGGCUGAAGCAGCUUUCCACUGCAUCUGUCCACCGAGGCAGUUCUGAAGCUAGUUGGGCCUUUUAAUGGCCGUAAAACAGAAUUGCUGUGUGGAAGGCCUUUCAGCAAUUUAGCUAAAGGCUUUAGAGGCAGUGGAGAUCUUUUCACUUACGAAUAGUGGCACUAAUGAAACAGGUGGGGAUACCUUUCCUCUAAAUGCUGCCAUUCUCUGUGUUCAAACACUGCAAACCCCUCAUCCGGAGAAACUUUCCCACCUUGGCUGUGUUAGUCCAUAUUAAACCGUUUGUUAAGUUUGGGAGCGGUUCUACAGAGAUCUUCUGGUUGUUUAAAUGUGAAUCAGAUGUCAAAAAGCCUAAUCUGCCCAGCUGGCAGUUUGGGCCCCAGUCUCAGAGGCUGCACAUGUGCGCAAGCCGUGAUUGGCAGGUGUGGUUUCAGGCAGCAUGUGACAGUGCUCCGGACAGGAGAGCAUGGCCUCUGCAAGUGUAUUCCCAGCUGGCAGGAUGUGGCUUUUAUUUAACUGCAAAAUGUCAGUUUAUCAUUACUGGGCGUGGGUAGAGAAGGAGGGACUCUGUACAAUUAAGUGUUUACUCAGCAGGUGACUACAAUAAGUACAGAAAUGGUUAAAAUGUUAUGACUGUGAUUUUUAAGUACAAUUUCUAGGAUUGUGGAGGUUACAUUGUAUAAAUAGGAUUAAUACCAAAUGAAUUUAAAGGCUACAGAGAAGAGAUUCCCUAGGAGUAACUCCCCACCCCUCCUUAAAAUAACGAUGUCUGUUUCUUUCCAAAGCAUGUUUUCGUUUUGUUUUUGUUUUGAGGGGUUUUUCGGUGAAAUUGUGAACCCUGAAACUAGUGUGUCUGGCAUUUAUUUCUGGAGAAGGCCCUUCUAAGUCUGUGUUUACUAAGCAAUUUGAGCCACAGAAAACUUUUAGUCUCUGAUAAUUUGAUAUCUGGUGAUGAGACAGUAAUUACAUCACUAUUUCUAGGUUGGUAAUCUUUGCUUUGGAAAAUGUGUAAUCCUCUGCUUCAGACAUACUCAGUGUGGAUCCAUCACAGAUGUGGCUGAAAGAAAAAAAUCUGCAACCUCUUGCUUUUGUACAUUCUUUUCUCUUGCCAAAGCUGUCUUGCCCUCUGCACUGUGAUUGUAUUAUACUGCCCAUUUGAAAAAUGGCCGAUAGGAUCAUUUUAAAAUCAUAAUCUUUAAAAAAUAUUUUUACUUUAGGAACGUUUGUCUUAAUUUUUGCCGAUAUGGUGUGUUAAGAUUAGAAUCUGUUAAUUUCCUGACAUUUAUUAACUACGUGAUAUUUAAAUUCCUUGCCUAUUUUUGAAUUGUAUUGUUUGACUUCUGUUUUUUAAUUUGUAGAAUCUGUUAUAUGUGUUGCAUAUAUUUUGUUUAUCUUUUAACUUUGUUCAUGGUGUCUCAUCUCAUACUUGAGUUGGGUAUAAUCAAAUCUGGAAUUUUCUCACUUAAGCUUUAUAAGUUUCUUGUUUUGCAUAAGAAGUGCUUAUCUAUCUCAAGGUUUAUGUAACAUAUUUUUUCAGAUACUUUAAGUAUUUUAUUCUAGGUGUUUAGAUUUUUCUUGCAUUAGAAUUUUUUGUUUAUUUAAUUAAUAUUAAUUGAGCAUCUGCUGUGUGCCAGGCCCUGGGCUCUGCAUGGGAUGAGUUAAGACAAACAUGGUCCCUGCACAAAUGGAGGUUGUAGGGUCAGAGGCAGGCAAUAAAUAAGAAAUCAAACAAAUAAAUAUAUAAUAUUCAUUGGUGCUCAGCACUGUCAAGGAAACAAACAGUGGAGAAUACUGUGAGGGCCAGGGACACAUAUUUAAGUUUUGAUGAGUUAUGAAGGCAUACAUAGAGUUUAGUCUUGCAAACAGAGAGGGGCAGAAGUGUAACUGUCAGCAUAUUCUAAGACUCUGAGGCAGGCUUGAGGGCUGGUUAGUGGGGAGUUGGAGCUUGGGAUGAGAUGAGGGUACAGUCAAGUCUUGUUCAUGGGCCUUGGCUUUAAUCUGGUUGCAAUAGGAAGCUGUUGGGUGUUUGGGGAGACAUUUAUGCAUGAAGCGGGUGUUCUGGCUUUGAUAUGGAAGGAAAGGAUGGAAGCACAGAGACCAGUUAGAGCCUGUUGCAUUGGCUUAGACCAGAAAUGAAGUGGCUUAGACUAGUGUAAUGGUUAAUUGUAUGUGUUAACUUGGCUGGGCCAUUGUGCCUAGAUUUGUGGUCAGGUGUUAUUCUCAAUGUUUCUGUGAAGGUGUUUUUGGAUGAGAUUAACAUUUAAAUCUCUAGACUUUGAGUAAAGCACAUCAGGUAAAAGCUUGCAUAGAACGAAAAGAUUAACCCAAUCCAAGCAAGAGGGAAUUAUCAGCAGAUGGCCUUCAGACUUGAACUGCAGUCUUGGUUCUUUCUGGGGUCUCCGGCCUGCCUGUGCACACACACACACAUGCAGACACACACACCAGGAAUGGUGACUGGUGAAGACACACACACACACACACACACACACACACACCAGGGAUCAUGACUGGUGAAGACACACACACACACACACACACACACACACACACACACACACACCCACCUCUUUGGUCCACUUCUCUAGAGAACCCUGACUAAUACAACUAGGAUGGUGGGAGUAGAAGUACAGAGAAGCGAAUAUAUCUUUGAGGAAGAAGCAACGGGACUCUCUCAGAGGAAUAAUUAAUUGAUUGUAAUGUAUGGAUGAUGAUGCCAUUCAAGGCAAAAAAGAGGAGCCGGUUUAAGGAGAAACUCAAAGAGUUUGGUUUGGGUCUUGUGUAGUCUGAGAUGCCAGUGAGAUAUGAGGGGAAGAGUUGAGGGCACAAAUUGGAUACAUGAAUCUGGAAUUCAACCAUGUAGAGAGGGGCAGAAGAUUUAGGACUGAGCAUUGGUGAAUUCAUCCUUUAGACAAAGGCUGAAAAGGAGUGACCAGGAAAUAGGGAGGAGAACCCAGAGAGCGUGGCAUCAUGGAGCAUGAGAGGAGUGUGCCUAAGGCAGACUGGAGUAGCUGACAACAUCACAUGCACUGAGUGAGUCCAGUGAGAUGCGACUUAAAGGAAGGGACUUAGAUUUGACCACUUGCAGGUUGGUGGCUAUGGUGGCUAAGGCAAAUCUGAUGGAGCAGCGGGGACAGUGUCCAGCAUGGAGUGGCUGAGCCAUAAGCAGGAGAUGAGCAAGUGCAGAGCCCACAUGUGACAGCUCUUUGGAACAGAUGUGCAGUGAUGGGGAGUAGCAAAACUAGGGAGGGCUUGGGGGUCAUGACUUUUUAAUGAUGGAUGAUAGGAGAGCAUGCUUAUAUGCUGAUGGAGAUGACCCAGUAUGGUGGGAUAUUGAUGACAAGUAGAGAGAGGGUAUAAAUGGUUCUUGUUUUCUAUCUAUUCAUUGGUCAAUUUUGGUACUUUUAUAUUUUGUUAGAAAAUCUUCCAUCUACUCUGGAUUUUUGACAAAGUGAAUAAUGUUCACUUUAUUUUAAUCAUUAGUGUCUGUAAUUAUAUCACCUUGUCUGUUCCUAAUUUUGUAUAUUUUUUGUUCUUCUUUUCUUGCUUAAAUAGCUUUUGUUUUACUCAUAUUUUCAAAGAGCCAGCUUAUGACUUCACUUACUUUUUCUACUGUUAUUUUCUUAAGUUUUAUUAAUUUUACCUUGUAUCUUUCCCCCUUCCUCCUACAAGAAUUCUGUAAACAAAAACAAUUUUAUUACUAUCAUGUGUGAGCCAAAAGUUUCUCUCUUGCUGCCCAAGGUCUUCCCCCAUGAGAGUCAUCAUGUGAUGCUUCUGGGUUGUCCUUAGUGAUUGUCCUGAGUGUCUCCACAUGCCCAUAUUUGGAAACUGAAUGUAGCGGUUCUGCCUGGGCUCUAAUCUCCAUUUACUUCUGUUCUGUUUUUGUUUAUACAAGAGACGGUCUGGCCUGGUCAUUUCUCGUCUUGGUAUGUUACUGCUGAGUCACAGUUCAGUUAACCAAGAACCAUGAGAAUGAAAGUUCUCAACUAAUCACAGACGGUAGAUUCCCCAAUGCAAUGAAAAACUCUUCUUUAUAUCAGGAAUAUUAAAAUGGAAGAUUACAUUUAAAAUAAUAAUUAAAUCUACCCAGUGCUUCAUGGUUCUUCUUGUUGAUUUCUCAGGGUGUGGUUAGCAAUGAACUGAGGUUUAUAACUAGCAAGUAUUAGUGAAAACCCCCUGAUAAUUCAGUUUAAUGGCUACUUUGACACAUUCAUCCUGAUUUAAACACAGACCCUACAGGUUAUAUAAACGGAUAAGAUACAAGUUGUUUUGGUAAAUUAAAAUCUGUAAAUAUGUAUGAUAAACCAGCCAGCUAUUUCUUAAGUAUUUACAUGUAGUUUUCACUCAGCUUACCAGGGCCCAGGGAUUUAAUUAAGCUGUACUGCAAGUUCUGUUUAUGGUUGUGCCAUAUACACAGGUGGUGCUCAAUAAAUCUUUGUUGACUUGAUGUUGAUUGAGUGUAUCUGGGGUUUACCUUCACUGUAGAAAUUACCUUACAUGGAUGGCAACGCUAGGUGUAUUCACCUGGUAGACAGUGGGUCUGUAUGAAGCUUAGGUUUUGCUGGCAGUCAGCAGUUUAAGUGAUUAACGAAGAGUUCUUACAAUACAGGGAGCAACGAUUUAAAGACAGAAUUCAAGGCCUCAAUAUAACUGUUUACAUUCUUUUUAAUCUGUGUCAUAAUUCAUUUUCAAAUAUUUGUAGUUGUUAUUGUAACAGAAGGUAUUUCUUCUUUCUUUUACUGCUACUACACCACCUUGCCCUAACAAUAAUGAGAGUUCAAAUACAGAGUGCUUAUUCUGUGUCAUACAGGUAAUAUCUAUGGCCACCAGAUUCUGUGCUAAUAAGCACUUUGCAUAUUUUUUUUUACUUUCCCUCACAACAGUUUCACAAGGUAGGGCUUUUAUCAUUUCCAUUUUCAGAUGAGGCAUGUGAGGCACAGAGUGUUAAGUAACCUCCCCAGGGUCACACAGCCGGUGAGAAGUGGAGUGAAGACACGCCUGGGUCUGUCUAAUGCCGGAGCUUCCUUUCAUAACUACCACACUCUACUGCCUUCGUUACCCUAUAGGGUACCAUCUAGAACUGGAAAUGACGACCAAGAAGGAAGGAAAUCUCACUAAAGGGCUGGUAAAAUAAUCAAUAUAACCACCAUUCAGCCAAAAAUACACACGCAGUUGUUGAAAUAUUGGCUUUUUGAUUUCUGAAAUGCUGAUGACUGUAAGUGAACAGCCUGUACUUCAGGCAAAGGUGAUUCUUUUUUAAGUAACUGAAUUCCUGAAUCAGGUCUCUCCUUCUUAAAGUUCCUGUUAGACUGUUUUUAAUAUCACAGCAGGCCUUAGCAGAAGAACUGUUGGCAUUUUCAUUAGUUGUCUUACAUUUGCAUUUCAAACAAACAUUCUGAUUGUUUGCCUCAUAGAUUUUGCCUGGUCUAAUGGCCAUUAGUGAUCAUUAUUAAAUGGAACUGUCUAAAGAUUUCACAAGUUUGUUUGGAUUUCAUAGGCCUUCUUUUUAAAUAAGAAAGUCACACAGUCAUCUCUAAUAUUAAAAUACAUUUAAUCUAGGUAUAAAACACCAAUUAAAAAAACAUUAAACUUGGUCUUUAAAUGUGAACCCAAGGAAGAGCACUGGCCUGUGCAUUUGGAGGCCUGGAACAUGCGCCCUGCAAUGUGGCUCCAGAUAAAUGUUCACUGUCUCUGAGCUUUAGGGAGAAACCUGUAAAAUGGAACUGUAGAUAAGUACCGUUUCCAUGCAGUUCUUCAAAUUCAGUAUUCUGUCGAAAGGAUGAUCCUGGAUUUGCUGGUGGUUUUUCCAUGAGAGUGUUACUUAGGAGAAAUGCAAAAGAUAUAGAUAAAGAUAAGCUAGAACCAGUGACAGAUUUUUUCACUUAAGUAGGCCUGCAAGCCUCCUUCCACAUGAUGUGAAAUACUCACUCAUCCUGGAGACUUGGACAGUAAUAUACCCAGUAGUGACAAUUAUCCAGGAAGGAGCUGGGGAUUUAAACAACUGUAGUAGUGGUACUCUAUUUUUAAGUUCAUGUGUCUGUGUACAGAGAAUUUUGCAUGCAUUCAUCCAUCGUUUUUAAGGGCCUACCACAUAGAUGUUAUUUUUGAGGAAAUAUUUUUCCCUAUAUAUUAUGGAUGAAUUGUAUUGUCAAACUCCACCUGAAACCAUUUCAUUCUCAUAGGCUCUCAUUUGGUUAAUUGCAAAAUAUGGUGAACUGCUAAAUGUCUUUUGCUUUUAGGGGGUGGCUCAGUUGCACCAUAGUUUACCAAGAUAUAGUUAGUAGUGCUUAACCAAUAAUUCAGCAAGCUAACUAUGUACAAUAAUUCCAUCCAUAGUCAAUUAGUUCAUAUUCUUUAUCUACAAAAGCUGAAUUCUGAUGGCUCAAAUCAUUUUAAAGUUAAAAUAGGCUUCUUAACCACAGACUUACAAUAAUAUUAAUAAUAACUCACUGUGAUUACAAAAAUCUACUGAAUGUUAACUAUGUGUUAGAUACUAUUCUAGCACUUAACAUGUGUUUAACUUAUCUAUUCUCACAACCCGAUGAGGUAAAUUCUAUUGCCCUGUUUGACAGAUGUAGAAACUGAGGCACAGAGAUGCAUGAGACAACCUGCCAGUGUCACACAACUGCUAAGUGAUGUUGGUCAGGUCUCCAAAGCCCACAUUCUUAACCAACUUAAAAUUAUCCAUCUGGGGCCAUAGAAGGUAUUUGUUGUUGUUGUUGUUGUUAAAAAAUACUUCAUUGUUUUCACCAAAUAACAGUGGGGUUGAUUGUACCAUGUUUGUAAAAAUGGAAGGAAAAAGCAGAUAGCAUCACCCCUUUAGUAAAAAAAUACUUGAGGGAAUGUUGUCUUAAAUAUCAAAAUAAGCCUGCCUUUAAGAGUUGCUUUUUUUCCUUUUGGCUUCAUUUUCAGUUUUUCUCUAAUGGCUUUACACCUCCUCUGUCCUACAGAAGUGAAAGCCCUCCUUGGCCCAUUCUGACUCAUAGUUACCUGUCAGUUCUGUUCUCAGUGGAGACAGCUUUCCUGGAACCCUCCCCUCCUUCGCUACACUUGAGCCUGCUCUCCAGGUCUGCUCACAGCCGGGGUCCUGCUGGCUCUGUGUCUUUCCCAUUAGAGGCUUUCCCAAGUGUCUGAUGAUAUUUGGAUGUCUGUUCACAGGGAGGGCCAGCUGGAGUCUGGGAGUGGGGAAGGGUGGGACUCAAGAAGCCUGGGCCUAGGUGUAGGAUGAUUGAAUUGGGGCAAGGCAGGGUCUUCUGGGGAUGCGUCUCCUGAUGUUCUGCAGUGGUGGGAAGUACACAGCAUAUCAUCUGUGAAGUCUUUUUGACAACAUCUUUAACCAGAAUCUGAUUAUUGAGAAACAGCUAGACAAAUCCAGAUCAUGGAGCAUUUUGCCAGAUACCUGUCCUGGUCUAUUCAAAAAUGUCUAUAACGAAAGACCAAAAUUAAAUAAAAAUAAAAGGCAGGGAAGUUGCCCUUUAUUAAAAGAGAUUAAAGAGGUAGAACAACCAAAUGCAGUGUGUCAUCAUCCCUUGGAUCCUGAAUUUUUCAAAAAAAAAUGCUGUUAAAGUACAUUUUUAAAACAAUUUGGAAAGUUGAAAUAUGGAGUAAUUAUUGCACAGAAAUUAAUUUAUUGCAUGUGAUAAUAGUAUUGUGAUUAUGUAGAAAAUUGCCGAAAGAUCUAGGGGUGACCAGCCUGGCCAACAUGCUGAAAUCCUGUCUCUACUAAAAAUACAAAAAUUAGCCAGGCAUCACAGUGGCACAUGCCAGUAAUCCCAGCUACUCGGGAGGCUGAGGCAUGAGAAUUGUUUGAACCCAGGAAAUGGAGGUUGCAGUGAGCCAAAAUCGCACCACCUCACUCCAGCCUGGGUGACAAAGCGAGACUCUGUCAAAAAUCUAGGGGUGAAGUAUCGUAAUGUCUGCAACUUAAUGUGAAUUAGUUCAGCCAAAAAAGGUAUGUUUUUUGCAAAUAUACAUAUCUUUUUCUCUCUCCACACACAUACUAGUGUGUGUGUGUGUAUGUGUGAUGUAUGUAUAUAGAUGUCUUCUGUAUCUGUAGACUUUUUUUCUGGGAACUAUUUGAUUUAUUAGGAAAACAUUAAUUUCUCAGAGUUGGACAGUGAAGGACAAAGCAGUGAUUAAAAAUGCAGUGAAACAAUGAAAACAUGAUGUUUAUGAGGCCAUUUAUUAGCCUGAUAAUUCAUUAACCAAAGAUUUAUUGAGUACCUGCUAAGUCUGCCCUUACUGUGCCAGGUGCUCCUGAGCAAGAUAGAUCUCAGUCCUCAUCUUGGUCAACUCUGCAGCCCAAUACAAGUACAAGUAAUUAGGGCUGUUGUUUUGGAAAGGGAUUAUGGCUAUAUAUACAGGAGGUCUCACCCUACUCUAAAUUAGAGUGGAGAAAAUCGGUGACUUUUCAGCUGAGUCUCUCACCCAUAAAAAGAUUAGGAUUUAACUGUUAAAGGGUGAGUGGAUAGAAGGGGGAUAGAGAAAAUGACAAAUGAAGGAGAAACAGCCAGUACAAAGGCCCUGCUUUAGCAAGAAAAAAUAAUGGCAGUUCCCUGCCUCUGGGAGGGGUCAGGAAGGGAGAUCUGAGCAGUAAGCAGGGCUGAGCUCCUGGGAGGACCUGCCAGCCCAAAUAUCAGGCAGGCGUUAGAGGGCUUGUUCAACAGGGGCCGAUUGAUGGGAACGAAUAUCCAUUUUUGAACAGUCACAUUGGUGAUUGCUUUGAUGUUAUAGAGAUGAUUAAAGAUCUCAAAGUUGGUGAAUACUUGGAGAUCAGUUAGAAGCUAUUGUCCAGGCAAGGUGAUGUGAUUUAGACUGAGUUGUUUUAGACCGAAUUGGUGGCAGCAAAACUAAAGAGUAGGUGACAGCUUAGAGCGAUAUUCAUAUAGUAGGUUAAUGUGGAUGCUUGGAUCAGUCCUUAGGUUGUCUUGAUGUGGCAGCUAAGAGAGCCGGAAAAGGCUGGGGCCACUCUGAGCUUCUGACUUGAAGAAAUGGAAGGAUAAUGUGAAUUUGGAGGAGGACCAUGGUCUUUUUCUUGGAGGGAGUAGAACAGGGGAGAAGAUGACUGCGGUUUGCGGUAUGAUGAAUUUGAGGCAUCUGUAAGACCUGAAGUGCUGGCAUUCAGAAGGCUUAAAAUGUAUGGGUGUGGAGCUCGGAAGUGGGGUUUGGGUAAGAUUAGGGAGUUUUUCAUAAAGAUGGUGUUUGGAGAAAGAGGAAAUGACUCCCCUGGAAAGGACUUUUAAACUGUUAAGAAGAGGGCCUGGAAAAGAGGUGGGAGUCUAUGAGUUAGGGUCUGGAGGGUGGGAAGAGAAUCUGAAAGUGCUUUAUUAAUCCCAGCACUUUGAGACGCCAAGGUGGGUGGAUCAUGAGGUUAGAUCGAGACCAUCGUGGCUAACAUGGUGAAACCCUGUCUCUACUAAAAAUACAAAAAAGUAGCCAGGCGUGGUGGCACGAGCCUGUAGUCCCAGCUACUUGGGAGGCUGAGGCAGGAGAAUCGAUUGACAUGGGAGGCGGAGGGUGCAGUGAGCCGAGACCAUGCCACUGCACCGCAGCCUGGGCGACAGAGCGAGACUCCCUGUCAAAAAAAAAAAAAAAAAAGAAAGAAAGUGCUUUAAAACCAGGUAGUGGGUAGCAGACUCAGGCUGCGAGAGGUCAGGAAGAGAGGACUGAGAAGCCUGCUAGCUUUGCCAGUGCAAGGGUCAUGGGGACCCUGUGGGGUGCUCUUUGACUAGAACAUGGAGCGCUGGAGAAGUUACGGGUACAUGCUACCGUGAGUGGACUGUGAGGUGGGAGGCAGUGAAGACAUGGAGACGGCAAGCCAGGAAUGCAUGCAAUUUGGGAACAGAAGAUCAAAGAGUGAUACUGGUAGUAUAGUGGAGUCAAGGAAGGAUUUACUCAUAUAUAUUUUUUAAUGUGAACGAGUCUUGCUUAAGUGAGCCUAUGGGGUCAUGAGCCUGUAGGGGAGGGGGAAGAUUGAAAAUUCAGCAGGGAAGAGUUGAUUGAGCUGGAUCCUAGAGAAGGCAGGAGUGACCUGAGCUUAGCUAGGACUGGACUGAAGAAGCAUGAAAUCCUCUUUUUUGUAAUAAGGUUGUCGGGGCGUGGGGUUAAGGGGAAGCUUGGAAGCUUAGAUAAAGGCAGUAAUUCUAUAGAAAGUUAAAAUGAAUGUUUGAAUAGCAAAACUAUUUGGUAGUUUUGAAAGUAAAUAAAAUGUUUUGCUGUCAGAUAGUGUUUAUGUGGAGCUGAAGACUUGGAUGCCCCUUUCAAGAGCACAGCACCAUUGCAAGGGGCUGCUGCAAGGACCUCUGAUCGCUUUGAGGGCCCUUGUGCUCAGGGUUGCCUCCGUCACACACACCUGACCCUGCACUGGGUGCUGGAUGUUGGAGAUAGGAAGUAAUUGGGAGAAGGAGGGGAGCAAUUAACUAAAUACAGCUGAAAUAAAAGGCUGCUCUAAGUAUCAUGGGUAUCUAAGAGGGUAAUUGGAGAGUUGGAUUUUUUUUUCCUGUGGACUAAUCAGUAACCAUUAUUUUGAUGCAUGAAAAGAACUACAGAUAACCUACCAAAUAGCAGUUAGCUUUCAAACCGGCGCUCCCAGGAGGAAGUGUGGCAACUAUUCAGAAGUUCACUGUCUUUUGCAAAGGCUGAGUACUGAAGUGACACACUUCAUUUACUAGAGUAUUUGCAGUAGGAAGGUGACCUAAUUAGAACAAAUGGUAACUUCAGGAGCUUUCUCAUCUUCUGAUUACAGGGUGGUGCUUCAGAUUACUUCCCUGUACUUGAUCAAAAGAGAUGUGUUGUGACUUGUUAGUAGAAUUAAUCAGAAAAACACAAAAGUUGUAUUAGAAUGUGGGUCUGCAUUUCUCUCUUCCAUUUCCCUUUCAAGAAAAAUUUUAAGUUAUUCUUAAUUGACAAAAGUAUCUCUUCUACCUGUCCCAACUUUACAACAUUCUCCUUCACCAAAUGGAUUAUACUUUGUAAACGUUUUAAGAGGUUCUUUCCAGUUUAACCUUAGUGUUUUGGUCAUACGAAGCGCUCCAGUAAGUUGUCAUUUCAGAGUUCAGUAAAUGACUCUUAAAAAUGUGUUAUUUCUAUUUCCUAUAUUCCAUUAAAAGCCACUUUGUUUUUCUAAUGGUUCUACAUUCCUAGAAUACACAAUCAGAGUGGUUUCCCUUCAGAUGUUUUAAAAUAACAUAAAAAUCCUGGACUUUAUCACCAGCCCGUGCAGUAUUCUAUGGCUUUUUUCUUUCCUCCUUGAUCGUUUUUUUUGUUUGUUUGUUUCCUGCUGUUGAGUAUUUUAUCAAUCUAAUACCAAUUUUCCUCUUGGUUUAUGGCUCUUAUACACUGACUGUUAACCUUUGAUAUGGAACUCUGUCAAGUAUUUUCUGAAUUCCAAGAUCACUGCCACUCCUUUGAUUAAACUUGUCUGUAUUAUCCUCAGAGGGAUUUGCUGCAUGUUAUGUGAGAAUGACUUGCCAUUCCUGAAAGCAUGUUGGCUAUGCCUAAUCAAAAUGUGCUCAACAAGUUAUCAAAUAAAGGUUCUUAGUUUUCAGUGAUUACAUGGGUAUUCAAUUGUAAUUCUGCAGAGAAAUCCUGGAGAGGUGGUUUAAAUUAAUAACAAAAAUUACCACCCCAGAGCAGAGUGAACAUACGACUUUAAGAUUCAUGAAUGGUAUCUUUUCUCCUCACCCUUAGACACAUGCUAAGAUUACUAGAUUACUAGUAUUAAUAAAUACUGUACUUUGUACAUUGACCACAAAGCUGGGAGAGAAAAAAAAUAACUGAAUAAUCUCUAUAUAAACCUUAAUGUUCCUGUCAUUGUCAUCAUAUCAAAAUCAGAACAGCUUCUGCUAUUGACUGCUGUGUUCUAGUCACUAUGCUAAUAAUUUUAUAUAUAUUAUUUAAUUGCUCCAACAGAUAUUUUUUGAUCACCUACUAUGUACCAGAUACUAUGGUAGCUACUGAGGAUAUUAUACUCACUACCCACAAGGGAUUUAUAAUUUAAUAGGAGACUCCAGCAAGAAAAUUUGAAGUCCCACUAGAACAUGAUAUUAUUGGGGUAUAUUAGGAACAGGAGCCAACUUUCUAGCAUGUUCAUUUUCCUUUAGCAAAUUGUAUUUACAUAGAAAUGAGACUUACAUAGUGUGGAUAAAGCACAAUUCAGCUUUAACAUCCCCUAGACCUACUCAGGGGAAGCAGAUAGGGAGAUUGCUAGGAAAAGAGGGCUGGUAAGGGUUACAGAGCCCCUCACUCCAGGUAGGAUUCAGCACCAGCUAAAGGCCAAAAGGGAUAGAAACUGUAAAGACAGCCGAGGCUUUUCUUGUCUGGCCAGAAGGUAAAGAGUGCCUGCAUCCACAGGGUUCACCAGCAGAGAGCAGGAACUCUGAGCAGGAUGGUACCUCAUUAUCUUUGGCUGUCCUAGGGACAUGGCCAUCAUGCCUUCUCUCAGGACAGACUGUGGACCUUUAUCCAAAUGACAGGCACGUUGGAGGUUGUCAGGUAUUCAGGCUGGGACUCAGAAGGCAAACAUAAAACUCUAAUCUUUUCCAGACAUAUAAGUUGUAAAAGCCAGACAUCUCUUGCAUGUCAGACACUGCAUUGGUGCCUACAUUCAAAGUGCUGUGUUAUCAAGGUGCAUCAGCCAGCUUUAUAGCCAGAGCUUUAACAGCUUAGGAGUUGUCUGGUGAGCAAAGAAAGAGUCAUUCUUGAGUGCUUGCCAUGAUGAGGGCAGGCGCUAAUGGGGAAGGAAUUGUCUCAAGAGCUCCUACUAAAGUCAUUGACCAUAGCAUGCAGGUGCUAUGGAAGUGCCCAGGGUGGCAGUCUAACUAGUUUCAGGGAGACAGAGAGGACUUUCCAGAAGAGAUGUCAUCUAAGACCUGAAAAAUAAAUUUGGAUGGAGGAGUGUGAGGAGGAGAUGGGAAAUGACUGUUCAGACAGGCACAGCAGAAUCUGCUCUAAGAACUAAAAGUAUUUCUAUUUCACUGGAAGGUGUAGGAGAAUGGGGGUCCUGCAAUACGAUUGCAUUUGCCUUUUUUCCUUGUGUUGACAUUUGCACUAAUGAUGCAAAAGCAGUGGUGGGUAAAACUGCUGGCACUUUAGCAUGAAUCAAUGCAGUGGCUCCAAACCGUAGUCAUUUUAUUCUUCAUUGCCACAAAGUAUCUGCAGUGAAAAAAAUGCGGUUUCAUUUGUAGAAGCAAUAACAUUAUUUUUAUUAAAUCUCCACCCUUGAGUACUCACGAGUUUUUAUUAUGCAUGAUGAAAUGGGAAGUACAUAGAUAGAACUUUUGUCACAUACCAAAGCAUGAUGGUUAUCUCUAAGAAAAGCACUUGUGCAGUUGUUUUACUUGCAAGCUGAACUCACCACUUUCAUAGAAAACCAUUUUUACCUAAAAGAAUGACAUACAAAUAUGGUUAUUCAGACUUGGGUAUUUGGCAACCAUUUUCUAUAGGGAAAUUACAGGAAAAUUUUGUUACCAGCGUUAAAAUUUAAGCUUUCAAGCAAAAAUUAGGAUUUUGGAAAACUUGUAUCUGCUACCAAGACUUGACAGUUCCGAAUACUUAAUAUUUUUCUGAUGAAGUUGGUGGUGAUAUUAAUAAAUGUGAUAUUUUGAUAAGUAUAAUGAAAUAUGUCAACAUUUGUAAGACCUGCAUAACUCAGUGAAUUAAUAUUUCCCAAAUGAUCAAUGCAUGAUGUUACAGAGUAGUACAUAGUUAAAAGAUUAAUUCAAAGUAUAAAUUACACCAAUGGAUUUUAACAUCACAGAGUAAGAAAAGCUCAUUGAUGUAGUUUCAGACUCCACAUUGCAACUGACCUUUAAGAAGUGACCCCCACUUGCUGAGUUUGGUGUAGUACCACAGCAGCGUCUGCCAUUUUCUGAAAAGGCUAUUAAAAAUUACCCCUUUUUCCAAUUAUAUAUGUACGUAAAGGAAGAUUUUCUUCAUAUACUUUCAACCCAAUCGAUGUGUUGCAACAGACUCAGUGCAGAAGCAGAUAUGAGAAUUGAGUCAGACAUUAGAGAGAUUUGUAAAAAUGUAAAACAACAUCACUCUUCCAGUAAAUUGUUUUCAUUUUGGAAAAUAGGUUUUUUUAAUAAAAUAUUUCGUUUCGUGGUAGUAUGUAUUGUGGUUACUAUUGUUUUUUGUAAGCGAAUAAAUGAAUAAAAAUUUUUAAUUUUAAUUUAUAAUAUGGUAAAUGCCCACAGAUAUAUGAACAAAAGCUUUUGGGGAUUUUCCAGUCAUUUUUAGAGAGCGUAAAGAAGUCUUGAGACUAACGCAUUUGAGAACCAAUGAUUUGAAUAUUUGAAACUGAAAAGCAUUUAAUAAGGGAAUUAGUUGCUUGCCAAGCCAUUUGAAGGGCUGGAGGACCAAUACCUGGGAAGGCCCUCACUAACUCUUAGGUUUGCCACUGGUUUUCAAAGAACUGGGAAAUUGCUAGCGCAGCAGGGUCAGGAACUACCGGAAAUCCUGGGUAAUUUGUACCAGGUGAAAGGAGAUAAAGAGUUGAAGUUAAACCCAGGAUUCAUGAUUGGAUCUUGGACUGGAGGAAAUGCAAAUGAUACAAGGCAUUACUGGGGAAAUCAGGGAAAUUUGAAUGUGGGUGUAUAUUAGACAUUGUUAUAUUAAUGUCAAAUUUCUUUAGUGUGAUAAUGGUACUGUGGUUAUGUAGGGUAAAUUUUGCCUGGUUCUUAGAAGCAUGCCAAAGUAUUUAGGAGUGAAAUGUCACAUUUCAAAUUGGAAAAAUGAAAAAAAAAAUGUAUGUUGAUGAGAGGGGUGCGGAGGAGGAAGAAGAGGGAAAGAGAUCAAUCAGUGGAUACCGUCUGCAAUUGGAACUUGUGCUGUUAAGAAUUAAUAGUAAUUAACAAAAGCAACUGCCACAAGAGUUGAAAGUGGUUUUCUUUGGGAUGAGGAUUGGGAAGUCAGUGUUGAAGAAGGGGCAGGUCAGUCAGUGGCUUCUGUGUUUUAUUGUAAGCCUUUUAGAAUGAUUUUGGUUUUUUUUUUCAACUAUGUACUUGUAUUUCUUAAGUUAAAAAUUUAAAAAUCAGAGGGAAAAUCCUAGAGACGAAUAGGGAGGGCUUGAUGAACUGCAGAAACAAAAAUUGUGGAAUUACCAAGUGAACAGGAGUUUGUGAUCCCAUUAGUUCAUAUUUAAGUUUUCCAGACAUAAAGAUGUGAUGAGACCCAGAAAAUGCCCUUGGGAAUAGGUGAAUAGAUUGAAAGUCUCUGCAAUUAAGGAGGUCAGAGAACGAAAAGGCUAAGGUUCCAUUUGGCCACCACAUGUGUUGAAGUUUCCCACAAUAAUGGCAUGAUUUGAAGUGCUAGGCAGGCAGUGCUUGUGGUCAGCCUUCAGUCUGGGUCCCUGUGGUCGGUAAGUUGAGGGGGAUGGGACUCAGCUAUUUCUGUCUGACCUAUGGCUGAACAUCCUCAGAGUUUUCCCUUGACAUAAAUGAAAAGAGAAUCCUCUUUUCUCUAAAUAACUAAAAAUAACUUUUGAAUAACUUUUGCUGUUCCUUUUGGUGGUAGGUAUUGCUCCCACCCUUGGUCUUAAGUAACUACCAAGAGCAUUUGGGUGCAGCUCACACAUUCUGGGCAUAUUGUAUAUGCAAGAUUUCUAAGCCAUCCCAAAGCUGUUUUAGCCCACCGGUGGUACUUUGUCUUGCUACGCUGUCAACUGAGAAGUGCCCAUAAGGACAGAUAAAAUCUCAUCUGUGGUCAUUUGCUCCAUCACCGCUGUCGAGUGCUUUGAUCCCUUGAGUCAAUGCUGCCAGUGCUGAAGCAACUUUAGCCAGUUACUGUGAAUGCCCCAAUUGCACAGUUGCUGGCUGGCUCAGGCCACCCUGAAGGUCAGUAUGGAGUCACAAGAUGAUUGUUUUCUUCUGGCUGGUGUACAGACCUCUGAGUUGAGAUGUCACAGAAUUGUUGUGGCCUGUCACCUUCUGUGAAGCCUUCCCUGGGUUACCCCCUCUACUCCCACUCCCCUCCCCCAUCAUGUACUAGCUGAGUCAAUGCUCACAGGGUGCUCAGUGUGCACCUCUUUAUGCAGUAUCUCACAUGUUGUAUAGUUAUGUAUUUUUAGGUAUCUUUUUCAACCUUGUUGGGAUAGAGAAUGUGAAUGAUGCCUGUAUCUUCAGCUCUAGUCAUAGUACUUGUCAUCAAGUGCAAAAUAUAUAUUUUUGGGGUGGAUAGAUGGGUGAAUAUAAAUAAGAUGGACAUUAGACUUACAUCAAAGUUUUAGAGAAAUUUCAUUAUAAAAGUAUUAAACAAAUGUGUGUUAUUUUUGUAUUGUUAUUUACAGCUGAUAAGGUUGCCAGAUGGCUGAAUUCCAAGUCGCGGGUGGUGUGGAGAUGCUAUUUAAAAGGCUCUUUUUUUUUUACUUUUUGGUAUAUCUAGGCAAUCCAUCUCUUCUUUUUUUAAGAGGAAAAAUACAUGUGACCAAAACUCAAGAUCCAUACAGACGCAUGCAUGUUGGCUCUCCCCCAGGAAUAGAAGUGUGAUUUUGAGGACCAUUGAAGUAGAAGACCCAAAGUCAAAUAGCUGACUGAGACCUUCAUUUAGUCAGCACAUUGUAUCAAGAGCCUCUUAUGUGCUGGGAAUAGUCCUGGUGGUUGCUAUUUGGGGCAGAAAAAAUUAGAGAACCAGUUGGAGUAGAUGUCACCAAAGAAGAGCAAGACAGUGAAAAUAGCUGGGGGAAAAAUAGGACAGAGACCCCGUUUUCUUAGGACAUUAGUAUGUCUCCAAAGCCAGCUUGGGGAACUGUGUCUGAAGUCUACAAAACAAUCCAUUCUCUUACUUCAUUAGGUAUUGAGCAUAGCUGGUUUUUCACAUUCUACCCUACGUUGCUUUGCUUUUCACAGAUACUACUGCGCUGUGUUUUAUUUUAUUAUUUUGGAAAGUGGCACUAUUUCCCCCUGAACUCUCCUGCCAGGGCUGACUUUCAGUUGAUCACUGAGCCUUAGCCUCUGCUCCUUAAGAAGCCCUGAUGUCGUUGCCAUGUGUCUUAGGCAUCCCCUCUUCUUUUCCCUGCCUCCCUGGGAUUGGGGGGAGAGAGGAUCUGUGCCUGGGACCAUGGCCUGACCUGGCCCAGCUCCUGCAGUGGAGUUGAAGACAAAGUAUGAGGCUUUCUGAGGACAACUGAAGCUCCUCAAUGCUGUCUUAUUGUUCUCCUUUUGUGGCAUGAGGAUUCUGACUUUGGGAUGUUUGAUCACAGUCCUGCCUGUGGCAGCUGCACUGCCAAGCUCGUGUAGCAAGUGUCUGAGUCAAUCAUGCAGGGCGUUAAGACUCUUCAUAACUCUUCAGUCUUCUGUCAGCAGCUCCUUUCCUACAAGUAUCCUGGAGGCUGGGCCAGGACAGGGGAUGUGUUCCAGUGGCCAGUCUGGGUGUGGACCAGAGGCUGAGCACACACCUGCCCCACAAGAGAGGGGAAGCUUGAGCCAUGGCUGAGACAUCAAACUAAAGCCAAUGGCUAGACUCUCCAGAGUUGCAGGGAUGAAAAGCCAGGCUGUAGAGUGGGGUCACGAGGAGGGUCUUAGUCCACACGUGCAGUUCGUGUGCCCUUUUCAGGAGCCCUGGCUUAGAAGUGGAUGGCAGGGGCCCUUUCCUAGACCUGCAGCUUGGCAGUCAUUGCCCUUCAGUCUUCUUAUGGACUCAAGCCCAUCUUUAAAAUUAUUCCUAAAACUAGAAAGUGACUGCAGGUAAACUGUCUGGAGUAUCACGUUCUGAAGAAUAGGAACUCUGGCACUGGGAGACAUCACUUCUGGUGGUUACCUGGAUGGAAAUGGAAACUGUCAGGGUAAUGAUAUCUUUUCUCCUCCAACAUGUGUGGAUGAAGUUACAGUUUUUAUCAUCAUGAAUUACUUUUAUUUCUGUUUUGCCUCUUACUUUUUGGGCCCAGGCAGAAGCUUUGCACAGUGGAGGCAGAAGGAGAUCCAGAAGGGAAUUAGCUGAUUGGAUACCCAGAGAGGAGUACACUUUAAAAGCAGAGUCCAAGUUAGCAGGCGAGAGGAGUGACUAGCCCACAGGGCAGCUUAGGGCAGUUCCUGGAGACAGAAAGAGGGAGAGGGACAAAGGCCAGAUUGCUGAGAAUAAGUAGAAAAAGAGCAAAGCCUGAAGCAGCAUGUGGACUGUUGUCAUUCAGCAGUUUGACAGUUUCAUUGUAAAGAGAAGAAUGGUGGUGGUGGUGUUUUAGGAUGGAGGAAGCAAAAAUGUGUUUGGGGGUGAGGUUAAUAAGCCAGUGGUAGGGAGGCAGGCAUUGAAGUAGCAAGAGAGGGGCUCAGAGUGAGCAAUAUUGGUGAGGGGUAGGAAGAUGCCAGUAAAAAACUUAAGAUUAUUUAUUUAGUUGGAUUUCUCCUGAAGGAUAUAUCAGUUUUCUGAAUGACAAAUAUGUGCCUUGCACAGUGGUUUUAUUUUGGUUUUUGGUUUUGGGUUUUUUUGAGACAGGGUCUCACUCUGUCACCCAGGCUGGAGUGCAGUGGCGUGAUCUCGGCUCGCUGCAACCUCCGCCUCCCAGGUUCAGGUGAUUCUCCCACCUCAGCCUCUCAAGUAGCUGGAACUACAGGCAUGCGACACUAUGCCCAACUAAUUUUUGUAUUUUUUGGUAGGGACGGGGUUUCACCGUGUUGGCCAGGAUGGUCUCGAACUCCAGACCUCAAUGGAUCCGCCCACCUUGGCCUCCCAAAGUGCUGGGAUUACAGGUGUGAGCCACUGCGCCUGGCCACAGUGGUUGUUUUUAAAGACUCAUUUACAAGAUUUGUCCUAAUGUCACUACAGUAUAAUUCCCAUCUUGGAGGGGUGAGCAUCUGCAGCUGUGAGGCACAGAGGGAAGGUUGAUGGGGGAGGGGAGAGAGGGUAGAGCCCCUGGAAGCUAUGCAGUGGCCUUACAGGAUGAUUUGGGAUAGGAAAUGAUGCUACUUUUUUGCUCUGAAUCCAUUUUUGGAUGUUGGUGGUAUUCACAGGUUGGAUUGAUUGGGUUUAGGAAGUAUUGUUUAGAAUAUCUACAAAUGAUAAUGUGUAUGAUCAUUGCUUUGGUAGAACAUCCUUAAUUUUAAUCUCUCUUCCUCUCCCAGCCCCUCUCCUGAGUAUGUCCAGAAUUUUAUCAAGUGGUUUCUUCUUGGUUCUCUUAGUAGGAAGAGGGCACAGAACCCUGUGUCUUGGAGGGGACCCAGCUUGGAGUCAGCUUCUGCUGUAUGUCAGGGGCAGCCUUGGAGCAGGCUGGAGGGCCCAGCAACCUCUAGAGUUUGGAAGCUGGAUGUUCAGCCUUUUUGGGUGGAAUACUGUAUAGGUGUUUUUCAUUUGUAAGAUAUACAUACAAUGAGGGGCAUAGGGUAGCAUUUUGAAGUUUGAUGAGUGGGGAAAGGCUGAUUGGAAGGGUAGAUAGAUAGGCUAAGACAGCUCAUAGCCUCCGGGAUUCCACAGCCUCGGGAGAAAUGACCAAGGAGAUAAACAGUGCAGUGCAGCAUUGCCAGCGUUGACAGAGGAGCAUUGCGGACCAGCAGGUGACUGCAUAGGCUUCAUACUCUCCUGAAUAGCCUUUUAAAUUUUAAUUUAGAUAUUAUGGGCAUCUUAGCAAAUUUCACUUAAUAGUCACACAUGUUGGUCAGUAAGUAAUAACUGCUUUUUUUGCUUAGCUCUAAGAUGUUGGCAUAUGUCACUCAUGAAUCACACAAUUGAGCUUCUCUUAUCUAUGUGACAGUCUCACUUCUAAUAGAGAUAACAUCAGAAUAGAUUUCUAUCAGCCUUAUUUGAGACUCAGCAAUUGAAACUUCUCUUUCCUAUCUUCAGAAGUGUAUUUGCUCUCUAGGAAAUAAUUCUGUAGUGAUAGGUUUUAAUGUGUCUUGGAGGCUACACCCUUUUCAUGGGCACCAAGGGGUUUGGACAUUUAAGGAUAGACAACCCUAUACUGUUGCUGUAGCGAAACAUAACACACAGGAAAGCCCGCCGGGGGAGCAUGCUGCUGAAUGCAUUGUGAGGGAAUAGACUUUGAUGUUCUUUUCACAUGAUUUGGGGUUUCCUCAAUAGGUAGGUAGAAGGAAAUAAUACUUGUCUUUUAGAUUUAGGACUUACUUAUAGCUUUUUCAAAACAUCAUUAGUUCAUGAACCAAGACUAAAAGACAUGAUUAGAAACAAAAUAACUUAAAUCAAUUGUUGGAAAUUCAUAUUUGGUGUUCAACUGUAAUACUAUUUUAAUUUAACUCUACAUUUUGGUAGCAAAACACAUGAGUUAAGGAGCAUUUUAAUUUCAAAAUUAACUGAGUCUUGAGAAUCAGAAUGAGUCUUGAAGUAUAGCCCAGUUUUGCAAAUCAGAUUUUUAAUUGAACUCACUAUUGUUUAAUUAUGCUUGUCAGGUCUUGUCACUGUCACCAGCGGUGUGGAAUUUAGGUACCUAAUGCUGUGAGCUUUAGUCAGUAGCUUAAAACAGUGUCACUGCAAAGUAAUGACACUACAGUGGGUUAUAGAAAUUAUGCAGUUUUAUUUUGUAGUCACAUUUCACGUUGUUAUGUGGUGGAAUAUAUAUCACAUUUAAGCUAAUAAUAUGAUUUUAUUUUUAUCUGGGAAAUACAUGCCAGUACUACUCAGGAAUUUGCUUAAUCUGGCUUAUAUUUUGCAGAGAUGUCAUCUCUAAGCUUUCAAGGUAGCAUUUAAUGUUGCUUUAUUUUUUAGUCAGCAUUAUAGAAAAGUAAAUACAAAAAACUUCAUGCAGUUGUUUAUGUAUUUGCUUUUUGUGUACCCAUGAAAUCAUCUUUUAUUUGGUUCAGAUUUUACAUUUGUGGGGCUCCUUGGCCAGGGAGUCAGGCAGAGGCUAUUCAAGGUCAAGGGGAAAAUACAUGUGUGAUUGUAGUGUUAUUUGUUAAGGUUCUUUUCUGUUUUAUGUUUUCUAUCUUCUAAGCCAGUCGUGAAGUUACACUGUGUUCAAUCUUGUUCUCUAGGUUCAUUUCCAGGUUUAUUAUUAAAGUAUAUUAAACUUCUUGUUCAGCAAAGUGUGAGCUCCUGUUGUUGGAUACUUGAGCAGCACUGUUAUUUUGUAAAACACACAUACUCAUACCCAACAAGACAUAGGCUGUUCUGUGCUGCAAGCACAGACACUCCUAAAGGCAGAUAUUUCACAGGAUUUGUAUCAUUUUUGUCAAAUUCUAACUCUCUUAUUUGCAGUGACCGAGUUUUCAUACAUUUGAUGAUAGUUUUUGAAUGAACAUUGCUAUGUGGUUAUAAACUGAUGGCAAUGGCAUUCAUUUUAACUUAAUUCAGAGACAAGAAAAGAGCAAAACUCUGUAGGCAAAGGCUGUGUUCAGAGUUCCAUUGCUUUCAGGAUUCAUGUCAUCAGGGCUCAGUGUUCUGGCUCCCCUGAAAAAGCUAAUUCAGUUUCUUUACUUACCCCGCAGACAGUUGGCUGUGUGCCACGAGCUGUUGACAGUUACUGCUUCUCUUGAGGCUGAUUAGCAUGCAAUGUUACACUGUCCCUAAGAAUAAUUUUGCUUACCUAUAUAAUAAUUCAAGAAUUUAAUCAUUUCCAAACAUGUCCUAAAUUAUUUAGUCCUUUGUCAGCAUCUCAAUUGAGUUCUAGAAGUUAUUUUUUUUUAAACAUUCACUGUGAGUGUAGUAGUGUGUUAAAUACAUUAAGGAAAGUGUUUCCAAACAGACUGUUGUUUCUAAAAAUAGAUUUCCUUGCAUUCUUUUGUUACAUUAUAGUUGCAUCUCUCAUCUGAGGAUAACAACAGUCCUGUGAGGCCAAAAUGUUAGCUGUGUCUCCCCUUUUCAUAGAGGAGGAAACGGAAACUGAGGCCAAGGUAGGGUAAGGAUUUUGCCCAGAUUCACGUAGCUGCCUGUGGUCUGCAGCCCAGCGCCCCUGCCCCCUCCACCUCCUGGCAGGCCUGUGGGCAGAUCCUGUCUUCUGGGAGGGGAAUGGGCAUAUAACCAGAACACAGAAGAGGAUUAUAGUGUCUAACCCACCAUCAUCAGGUGUGCAGAGACCAUUAAUCUCACAGAGGAGAUUCGUAUUCUGCUGUUGUAAGAGGAGGACUCCUCUGGCAGUGAGGGGAGGACUGCGUCCGGCUUGGCCAGGGGUCCACCAGAGGUCCCCCGUCUGCCACUUUCUGAGUGACAGCCAAGCCUGGGUCAUUCUUUUCACCCCACUCACUGCAUCAGGAAACUGUGUAGUUUUUGAGGUUUGCAUUAAACAAACAUUUGAUACCCUUUCAUUCUGCUCCACAUUAAAAGCUAGACAUACAUUUCAUUAUAGGAAAAGCAAAAACAUGUAAUAGAAAAAGGCAGUUUAUUUCUUAUUUUCUAACCUUUGGGAUUUUAAAAUUUUGACAGUCAUCUCUCUGUUCUCUCCUCUCUUGGCCCAACGUGCUGUCACUUCUCCGUGGUAGGAUUGCCUUUCCCUUCUGCCUGCUCCAUACAGUGUUAUACUCACCAGCUCGCAGAUCUGUUAGCAAAUACUGUUUAGUCAGGCUCUUGCUCAGCCAGCUAAUACAGAGCUACUAUUUAUGAAGGGUCAUUCACCAGGGAAGCACUCUGCUAACUACUUUUCACAUAGGACCUCCUGUAAUUCCUCCAACCACCUCAUUAAGUUGGGUAUUCUAACUAUUCCUAUUUUAUAUAUGAAAAAAUUGAGGCAUAAUGAGGACACCUGCUCAACAUCAUGUAGCUAAUACGUGAUAAAGCUGGGGUUUGAGCCCUGUUUUGCUGGACUCCAUAGCCAGUGGUCUACCAAAGAAGAGACUGAUUUUGUCCCUUCCUUGGCCAGAUUAGGUAGUUGUGAUCUAUCAUUGUUUUCUGGCACAUCUCCCUUCAAAUAAUGUAAACCUUUUCUAAAAAGUAGCUAGCAGCUUUUGCACCUAGAGAAUUUUUUUUGUCUGUUCUGAUGUUCAAUUAAGCAGACUAGUCUAGUGUUCAACAUAUAAGCCAAGAAUUGCACUUUCUUCUUAUUUAUGCCUUAUGGCACUAGAGCAAAGAAGUAGUUCCAGGUGGAUCUUCUGAUAAUAAAAAUGAUUAGUGUUGAGACCAACAUUGUUACUUCUUUACUUGUUGCCAAUUUUUACACAUUUGAGAACUCUGUAGUUGACUGUGUAGUCAGUUGCAUACAAGUUAAUGUCUUGUGCGAGAUUUUAAGGUUAAUUUCUUCCUGCUUACUCUUCCACCUCCCAGAUGUUUUCCUUUAUUUUCCCUAGGAGAUGGAAAUGGAAAUGUUAUUCUUCUUUAUUGUUGCGGGUAAUGCCUUAAGAAAAAUCAGAUCCAAGACUGUGUGCAUGCACGCACAUGUGUGCGUGUGUGUGUGUGUGUGUGUGUGUUUGAGAGAGAGAGAGGUUGGUGGGGAAUGAAGAGAGAGGAUUUAAUUGCCAAGAUGAUUACAGAUUAAGCUACAAAAAGCAAGAGAGCUAUUGGUCUGAAACUGUGUUGUGUCUGUAGAGUGCACUCUGAUUCACAGAAAAUUUUGUCAACAUUAAAUGCGAUGGGAGUUGAGUUUUCAGAGGUGGUAACUAUGAAGGGGUUGGUCAUGUAAUGCUGUGCACAUAUUAGAGCAACAGGCAGUGCUCUCGCACUGCUUUUACCUGGAUUUAUAAAAUGCCCAGUCCUUAUACUCUUGAGCAUGACCAGAUCCAUUUCCUGUUUUUUUCACAUUUCUUUUUCUAAGAAUAAACAGAACCCUAGGAAGGGAAGGUAGCUUCAAAUACAAGCCAUUUUAAGUAUCCUGGUCUCUUAAUUCCUUUUUUAUUUUUUUUUGGAUGACUUGAGGACAAUAAGGUGUUUGUUUAUUUAUUUAUUUAUUUUGGUUUUAAGGAGCAGAGAGUUUAAUAGGCAAGAAGGAAGGAAGAAGACAGAAGGAAGAAGCUCCCCCGUACAGAGACAGAUGGGGGCUCCAAAACUGAAAGAGGAGAUCCCCCUCUUAAUUCUUAAACUAUUUUUAAAAUGAAUGUUGACUUUCCUGAAGUUAUAAACUGUUUUUAACUCUUAUCAGUCCUCCUUGAUUUUCCUUGUUCAGGUUCCAUCUUUUUAACAUCCUUUCCUCUCGCAGUAACUACAGCAUGAUUUGUUUUACCCCUCAGCACUCAGCUAUCACAGUCAUAGCUCUCUCAUCUGAGCAGCCUCUCCCUCAAUCUUACAAACAGUAGGCAUCCACAAGGAAGUCAAAGAAAGGGUCUCUGAGCUGCCACACACUCAUAAGAGGCCUCCUUAGUCCUACUCCCAGGACACAUUUGUUCUUGUUUAUGGAUGAUUCUUAACUGGCUGAUUAUCCCAUUUCUAUUUCAGUAGCCAAUUUAAAAGCAGAAAAUUAGAUGUGGAAAAUUGUACUUAGGUUGGUAAACUGAAAAAUGACACGACAUGCCUUGACUCUAUUCAGUUAGAGUCAUUUAUUUAUUUUUACAUGUUUGUAACUUGCCCCAUUCCACAGCGGACUUGAGGCAGCUGACAUUCUUACAGAAAGAGUCCCUUGUUAUGUCUUUAAUGGAUGCAGCCUCCUUAAAACAGCUCAGGAUUGAAAAAACUCUUGUGCAGAACAGUUAAUUGAAGUGUUCUGCUAACAUUUUUUGUUGCUUUAUUAAUGCUUGCCCUGGGAAUCAUAUCAUAAACAGUUUAGGUAAACAAUAAGUUAACAACACUGAGAAUUUUCCUGUUUCACCAAACGUGUCUUAUCUACAGGCUGCAGACAUUCAGCAUUACCUUGUCCCUUGCUUCUGUUCUCUUUAUAAAGCUCUGGACAAGAGGCACACAACAGACGUGUCCCAGCUGCUGACUCAGUGUGACAGAGCACUGUUGCCAGUGCCCAGGUGACUGCAGUGGGCCACACUGCAGGAUUGAUGGUUUAACUCUCUGUAGCUUCCAAAUCAGAUUAUUUUCAUUUGCGCAAAGGCACACCAGCAGGGGUGUGUACUGUUUGACGCACAGAUGACAAUCUGGCCGGAAGCUAGUACUUGGGGAAAAAAAUAAGGGAAAGGAAAAUGAUAGUUUUGAAACAACAUAGUUAUAAAACACAGCAUGUAUCUAUAUUUUUCUUCUGAAAAAUGUGAAAAUUUUCACCCUGGAAAAAUACCCAGAAACCAAGCAAUAGCUUCCCUGUGUUUUGGCAUUUAUAUAACAGUUUGUAUAAAAGGACAACGCUGAUUCCAAUACUACGUGUGAUUGUGCCAAAAAAUCAUGAGAUGAAACAAUCAGUAUGUUUGCACUUUUGGUUUGAAAUUUUUUAAGAGUAUAACAAUGAAAAGCAAAAAAGGAGGGAGUGAAAGAAGAAUCUGCCCUACAGUUGAAGAGCAUAGGGGAGGUGGCAUAGAUUGAAAAGCCAGGUGUCUGCAUAACCAAUGGUUAGAGAACCACCACCAAGAUGAGGAGGUGAAGGAGAUUAGCAUGAAGAUGGGGAGUAGGAAGGAGGAAAUGCCGCGAAAUGGUGCCAACUUGUUUGACUAAAAUUCAGAAUCCUACAAGGACUUCCAGAAAAUAUAAACAGCUGCACAGUUUGAAUUAUAUACUUCCUACAUUUCUUCAGUUUUCAGAAGCACGUGAUUCUGUCCUUUCAGCAGUGCUGUGAAGGAGAGGAGGCACAUAGCCCUCGUUUAUAAGCCAGGUGACCGUUAGGCCUCAUGACAUUCUGUGCCAUGGACAGCUGUAACAGACUGGAGACAAAGCCGUGCCUCCACCUGCAAAACUGGCCAUGCUUUCUAGAAAGCCGAAGUUGCAUUUCAUAGACUGCACCAGAGGCUGUAAUACCCACUUCUAAAAAGAACAAACACUUUGUGAGGCACUGAAUUUAGGCCAUUGGGAAGGAGAGGAAGGGCCUACCUAAGGAGGAUCUGUGCCCAGGAAGUGUUGCUCAGUCCCUGAGACAUUAAUAGGAGGGAGUUCAGGUAAGGCAGCCAGUGGUCACUUGGAGAAAGGAGGAUAAGUGGGUUCGAGGCAUCAGCUUGCCCUGGACCUGCAGUGUUGGCAGCAGGUUCCAAGGAUUUGCCUGCCAGCUGUUGAGGCUAAAAAUCUAGGAAUAGGCACAUGGUUUUCCAACCCCCUGUACUCCACCUAACACAGUGCUCAGGAAUAAUUGUUUCAUUUUAUAAAACAAACUGCAGAAGACUUGUAUUUGCCAGAUCCCAAAUUGGAAAUGAGUGUCUUCUCUAAAACUCCUUUGUCUGACUGCCAAGGUAACUAGACUUAUCACGAUGAGAGACUAGGCCAAAACACACACCCAUAGGGGCCCAGCAUACUGUUUUAAGAGUUCUCCCUUUUUGUGUAGAUGCUCAAAGGGAAAUUGUACUUACGGAAACCUUCAGCUGUCUGAAACCAUCGGUGAAUGGGUGAUUCUAUAGAGAAGAGUUUUAUAAAUAGUUGAUAAUUUAAAUGUUCAGAUUUUAUUUUAACCUUCUUUUGCAUGGUUAUGGCCUCCCUUGAGACGAAUUGCUUGGUUCCUUUUGUGUGAAAGAGGGAUAACAACCCUCAACUGGGAGAAUACUGAUGAGCUUAGCAUACGUAUCCUGAUAACAUGUGACAGCCACGAGAGGAACUCCAUGAAGUUUAGCUUCCUGCCUCUUGCCAGCCUCGAAGAGACUACACAGCAAGAAGUCCUUGACUUGAAUAACAGUUAUUUUGUGUUAAGGUAGAUUUCCUCUAUGCACAAUGGCCCUAGGCUGCUAUUCUUUUUUAGCUUUGGACUUUUUUUUUUUUUAAUAGUUUUUCCACCUCCUUUUCUUAGUUUUGAAAAAAAGUGUACUGAUAAAAAACUUUACCAACUUCCUGCUGUAUUAUGCUAGAAGCUUUAUCUGUGUCACCUCAUUUAAUCUUCAUGGCAAGAUGUCUUUUUCAUUGGUCUGCAUAUGUGUGGCUUAAUUAAAUCAUUUCGUAGCUGUGAUUCGUUUUUUCCAAAUUCCAGAAGUUGUUUUGCUGGAUGUAGAUCAGAAGUGGGAACAACUUAGUUCCCUUAAUUUGCCUAAGGCAGAUUUUCCUUAAGUCGCUAUUAAAAGUGCUCGCAUUGUUAGGUGAACCAAGUGUUGAAUGGUACUUUACAAAGGUAAGAACAUUAACAUCUACCACUUAGUUGAAGCUCACCACGUGCCUGUGCCAGACACUGUCUGAAACCCUUCAUGUAUUUCCAUUAAAACAGCUCUAUUUGACUUAGAGGAACUGAUAUCAUGCCUUAAAAUGAAAAAAGUGUUUCAUCAAAGGCAAUAUGAAAAUAAUUUGUUUUGAUGGAAAAACUGUCUUUUUAGUGCACAGUGAAAGCUUAAGAGGAUAGGGAGCAGAGCCAGCUCUAGUUUGUACAUAUUAGAAAAGGAUGCCCUCUCUGGGCAGACACUGCACAGGCUUGGUGAAUGGAUGGUCCUCUUGUGCCUCUGAUUCUCUGACGCUAGGCUGUGUGGCGCAGGGAGCUGAGUGCAGGGUAGAUUUCAGCUUCUUGUGCGCUGUUGUGCAUUGCACAGCCUGGCCUAACUACAUGGCAGCUGAAGUGUGUGUUUGCAUGUUGUAGGUGGGGUAGAGUGGGCGAAGGUGUUGAUGGAGAAAGGGCAAAGGAUGAACGAAGGAGAAGGGAACACGUACAGGACAAAAUGAUACCUUGGCAAAUGGUGAACAAUCGAGGACAUUAUUUGAGAAUUGGGAAGGAGAGGAAGGGGUAAAUGGCUGCAGCCGACCCCUGUUCAAGGCCUGUAAGGCAGUUUGGUCCUCCCAGUGACCCCUGAUGCUCGUGCCUCCGUCCACCUCUACAGCCUGUGGCCAAAACCCAAAGGAAUAAAGAGGGCCCUGGAAAACCCAAGCAAAUUGCACUAUUCUCACCACCACUGCCGCUGCCAAGGGAGUCUUUCUUUCCUUAACCGUAACUCCCUCUCUGGUCUUAAUUUCUAACUUCAGAGCUUAAUAAUGCUUCUUCUUAAGGGGCAGAGGAAUUCUUAGGCUCCCAGUGCUCUCUGGGAGAAGGACUUAGAGACACUGGGGGAUGGUGUGAAAUACUUUAGAGCUUUGACAUUCUCCCCCUUGACUCAUAUGGGGGUUCCCUGUCACUGAGUAGUAUUCAGCCCAUAGGUGGUGAGACCCAGCCCUUGGUCUCUGAAGACCAUCCUGGUCUCUACUCGCAUGUUGUCCUGUUCCCCUAUGGCUUGCAGAUGUGCAGAAAAAGGCCACAAUUGUGGAUUGGGUGCAGUCAUAAUAAUAGGAAAGCAAAAUAUGAAAGCAGAUGUAGAGAGAGGAAAAUCUAAUUGUAAAAGAGCCUGUUUAUAAGUUGCAUACAUGUCUUGAUUAUUUUUCUUCUUUUCAUACUAGAAAAUAUUUGAUCAUUUAUUAUUAUUAACUCCAUUGAGGGCCAAAUGCAGAUUUCAAUACUGUGUUUAGUAACUCUCUGAAGUUGCAGAAGGGCAAAAUAAGUCACAGUAGGUUUUUCGUUCAUUUUUCUAAUUUAGGCAUCAUUCACUCUAAUUUCAUAAGAUUUGAAUGCAGUUUGCUAAAAUUCCAGAAGGAGAUUAAUUUACCAGUUCGUGUCAUAUAAUACUUGUUUUCCCGUACCAUCCAGCACCCAUUUUGGCAAAUAGAAAUAUACAAGGAUGGUGGAGAUCGAUGUACUUUAGAGUGUAUUUCUGAGAGCAAAUGACUUCAUAGUCUACAAAAUAGUGGGGCAGUAUAAAUUCAUCUUAUGUGAAAAUAUGGAUGAACAUGGCUUUUAAAAGGAGAAAAGAAAGGAGACCGAUGAAUGUGUAUAUAUACUUUUAAAAGCUCUGGUUUAGAAAUCAGAACAGGUUCAGAAAUAUCCAGAAUAAUGCCUAGAUGGCUUUCAAUAUUCAUUUGAAUGGGCUGAUUUCAGGUGUCCAUCUUCAGUUAUAGGAAUACUUGCUUCCAUACAAUGAUUUAAUACUGCUUGCAGACCUCAUAGAGACGUGAUUUAGACUCAGGGAAAAGCAGAUUCUGGCAUUGUUUACUCAAUCUGUCUUGAAUCUCAUAUCCCACCUGGUGGUGACUAUGACCUAGUGUGUGGUCUGCACAGUUAAUAAGUUGGAAUCUUCUCACUUGGAAAGUCCAUUGUGAUUUGCCCUCUGGUGUCUUUUUAAAAACUCAUUAAUAGCUUACUCAGAAACUUAGCUGGUAAAAUUGUUGCACUUGAGAAAAGGGCCAUCUGUUCAAAGUUCAGUAGGGAUAGAAUUCUUACAGUAUAAUGUAAAGUGUUAUGUAUCUUUCUCUCCUUUUAGAAACUGAGCUCACAGACAAGUUCUACCCACUGCAGUUUGUCAGGAUUUUUUAAAUUAUUAGCUCACAAAAGCAAAUCAGAAUUUAAUAUAUUUUUUGUGUAAUAGUUUGAUUUCUGUAUAUAUACAUGGAAGGAAAUGUUUUGCUACAUUUUUGCAGGGCUUGUUGUAUUUUAACAAGGUAAUCUUUUUUUCACUGGACUUGUGAGACUCAUAAAAAUGUCAACACGUGAAGUAUAGUUGAAUUAAAAUGCAAAAACCUGGCCCCCAUACCCUCUUCCUGUCUGCCUCAGCUCCCUUCUCUGGGUCCCCUCCUAUUUGGUACAUAAUCCUGCCAUAGCACCAGCCACACUGCCCUGUAAUUGCUGAUAGUAAUUACUAAGUGGUUUCUCCCCCAGUGCUCUGCCUCAUUUGAAGUUCUUGGUGUGUGCACAUAACUGUAUGUUCAGUGGAUGUCCCCAUAGCCUACCGUAAUGCUGGGUGCUUAGUACGCGGAGAGUGAGUAAAUACAUGUGCGUGUGCAUAUGUAAUCAGUGUUUGGUAAGGAUGAACAAUGAGGAUGGAGGUCUGACCCUGGUAAACAGGGAAACGAUGGGGCCCGUCCAGGAAUUCCGAGCAGCAGCUGUGUGAACUUUGGACUUCAGAGGCACAGGCUGAGGUGGGGCAUCAGGCUGCUGUUAGGAGAGCAGUGUUGGAGCGAGGCAGAGGCUGGCUGCUCCAGGAAGAUUCCUGAGGUAUCAGGAAGGUUUCUGAGAGCUCCGACUGAGUACAGCGUGUGAAAGAGGCUAUCAGCUGCAAAGGUCAACACAGUAUAUCCUACACUUUGUCAAGGAAUCAGACUGUGGUGGUGGAGUACACACAUGAUAAGGAUACGGAUAUGUUUCAGGUGGGCAGAUCAACAGAAAGCCCUAUCGACUUCGUUGUCACAGACACGAUUUCUGGCAGCCAGAACACGGACGAAGCCCAGAUCACACAGAGCACCAUAUCCAGGUUCGCCUGCAGGAUCGUGUGCGACAGGAAUGAACCUUACACAGCACGGAUAUUCGCCGCCGGAUUUGACUCUUCCAAAAACAUAUUUCUUGGAGAAAAGGCAGCAAAGUGGAAAAACCCCGACGGCCACAUGGAUGGGCUCACUACUAAUGGCGUCCUGGUGAUGCAUCCACGAGGGGGCUUCACCGAGGAGUCCCAGCCCGGGGUCUGGCGCGAGAUCUCUGUCUGUGGAGAUGUGUACACCUUGCGAGAAACCAGGUCGGCCCAGCAACGAGGAAAGCUGGUGGAAAGUGAGACCAACGUCCUGCAGGACGGCUCCCUCAUUGACCUGUGUGGGGCCACUCUCCUCUGGAGAACAGCAGAUGGGCUUUUUCAUACUCCAACUCAGAAGCACAUAGAAGCCCUCCGGCAGGAGAUUAACGCCGCCCGGCCUCAGUGUCCUGUGGGGCUCAACACCCUGGCCUUCCCCAGCAUCAACAGGAAAGAGGUGGUGGAGGAGAAGCAGCCCUGGGCAUAUCUCAGUUGUGGCCACGUGCACGGGUACCACAACUGGGGCCAUCGGAGUGACACGGAGGCCAACGAGAGGGAGUGUCCCAUGUGCAGGACUGUGGGCCCCUAUGUGCCUCUCUGGCUUGGCUGUGAGGCAGGAUUUUAUGUAGACGCAGGACCGCCAACUCAUGCUUUCACUCCCUGUGGACACGUGUGCUCGGAGAAGUCUGCAAAAUACUGGUCUCAGAUCCCGUUGCCUCAUGGAACUCAUGCAUUUCACGCUGCUUGCCCUUUCUGUGCUACACAGCUGGUUGGGGAGCAAAACUGCAUCAAAUUAAUUUUCCAAGGUCCAAUUGACUGACGCCCUUGACAGCCAUCUACGACUUUAUUAACAGGUUACUGUGAAGAUUUUGCCACUAACUCUAGAUUUUACCUUUUUGUAAUGCUGUUUAUCAGAGGAGGGUGACAGGGGCUGGAAAUAAAGAGAGGGGACAUGGUGAUGAAACAUGGCAGGAGUGUAACAGAUACCAGUGGUGUGUUGCAUGCUCAAAACAGCAGCGUCGUCAUUGAAGUCUGCUUGAUUAAACCAUAAUAUCUUUGUAAUAAUUGGAUUUAAAAUGCUAUGCUUCUAUUUUUAACCUUGGGUUUUUAACCAAGUUUUUUUUUUUUUGUAAUCUUGGACAAGACUUUAAAUCAUAUUUUACAGAUGUAGAAGAAAUUUAUUCAAAAGUGUGGGCUCAUGAAGUUCACUUCAGUGCAGUGUGGUGUAGGUGUUACGCGAAGGGCGCACAGUGUCUAGAAAUACUUGAUCGUGGCUCAAACCUGACCAGACAGCAGAGGGGCGGCUCUGUACAGUGUGACUGGUGGACAGAUGGCCUUAGGCACAGGUGGUUUUGAAAUCUGGGGCUUUUUCUGAUUUAUUUUUCUGACUUGUUGGGGGAGAGAAUAUUCAUAACUUGUGGGCUUUUUUUUUUUUUAACUUCAGUGGAAUUUACUUUAGAUAUUCAUUCAUCAAAUACAUGGGACUUCACAAACAAUUUUCCAUAACUUUUUAGCCUGUCUUUUGUUAUUUCUGCCUAAUAUGAUUUGCCCCGAUACUCAUCUUGCACGGCCAGAACUGUUUGGUUGAUUAAAAUACAUCAGCUCUUAAAAACUCAUUAACUGAGGGUAAUUACAGUAGUAGACAUGGUCUGGGUACUAUACUACCAUGUUUAUUUGCUGACUGAAUUAAGAUUUAAGAAUGAUUAAAAAUAAGCUUUUACUUUUUAAAACCACUUGAGGUUUCAUAAAGCUUGGGGUUUUUUUUUUUCCUUUGUUAAGAAAGCCAACCAAUCACAAUGAUAUAGUCAUUGUUGUGCACUCCCUUUUCACCAUCUGUCACCUUCCCUUGCAGCUUAAGGAGCCCAGUAAGUUUUGAAAAUGUUUGCGAAUCAAACUAAAUUUAAGUGGGAUGAUUAGAUAUACACAACACCAAGUGGUACAUCUGCAGAGAUAAUUCAAAAUUCCUGCUUUUGAGAGAGCAAAUGAGUGUUGCUGAGGAAUAAUUAAAUGAGAAUUUCAUAGGAGCUCCACCAUUCCUGUUACUUUCAUUUCAUUUUGAUUAAUAAUUCUUGGAUGCUUGGCAUCGAUCGUAUCACUGCUCCUAGAAGGUAAAGAUCCUUUAGGACAUGAGACUGGUAGAAGCUGGCUGAGAUAAAAUAAGUAUUUAUUUAAACUAAUGUUCUCUUAAUUUGACCAUUGCAGAUUUGGGUGACUUUUUUUUAACCUUUGUACAUAUACGUAAUUUAUAUGAUUCUAAUGUACUAUAUCCAUACUUGAAUUGGUUUUUUCGUAUUUUGCCUACUGGCAAAUAUUUUGCCUAUUUUCAGUCGUUCUAACCUAUUUGAAUACGCUUUUCCUUAAAGUGAUACGAUAAUAUUACUCUUGAUUGCUGCUGCUUAAUUUGAUGUAAUAUGUUUAAAGUUCAGCCUCUCAGUUUUAAUAUAGCUUUAUUUUUCAGUGGAGAUCAUUGUUUAGGAUGAGACAUUUUUGGUUUUGGUUUUGUUUGGGUAAAUUUUAAAUGGUGUGAAAAUCGAUGACAACAGUCCUCUUACAGAUAGCUUGCUGUAUUCUGUAUAGCUUACUCUACCUGCAGACAGAAAAUGAAAGAAAAAAAUGGACUUGCCUAGAAUAAUAUAUUGAAUGCCUUUUGAUUUAGCCAGAGUCUCUGAUGAUUAGCUUUCACUGAUAGAGUAUGUCUUUUCAGCCUGUAAUUCUUUGGGCCCCAAAGAAUGACAAAGGAGGCACUCGUUCUCUUUUCUUGCUGUAUGCCUAGAAAGUGGUUGAAGGAUUCUUGAUGCCCUAAAACCAUCUUGUAAGCUAAAUGGUCUUGCAUCCAGAAAGGCCAGAUUUUACCUACCAAGAAAAAAAGAUAUUUUUCCAGAGAGUUAGGUAUAUCAUAAUUUUCCAUUUCAAGUCCUGUUUAUAAGUCUAGUCAUUCUGCAACGUGACAUAUCCCCCAAAAUGAAGUUACCUUCCAAGUUGGACACGUCCCGUAGUUGGGCAUAUGUCUAACUAAAAGUUUCUGACUUUUAGUAAAUUCAGCUUAAAUAUAAGUUGAAAUUUGGGAAAUAAUUUCCAAGCUCUUGGAAGGGGUAACAGUGAACCGCCCUCCAUGGGCUCCACAUCUUUUCCUUUGGCUUCCAAAGUCAGGUCCCGCCCACCCUGCCUAAGGAACUGCAGAGAGGUGGCAAAUCAGCAAAAAGGACACCAGGCUCUUCUUGGCCACUUGUAGGAAGAUCCCUUUACAAUUUUGACUAAGGAGAUUUUUUUUUUCACAGUUGAGUUAGUUUGUGAAAAUAAAGAACUCUGUAGCUCACCAAGGUGGAGAAACGCAAUUCAGAAAAGUAAUUUCUCCAAGGUCACUUCUUUUUUUAUGUCUUGCCAUCACUUUAAAGGACUAGCCCCACUCCCCCAUGUGUAUACACAAGGAAAUUGCAGACCAAUUAGUUGUCUUGGCCUGACUCUAAUGCCUUUUGCAAGUAGCUUUCCAGAAGUAAAAGUCCCAGUGAUGUAUUCCCAUAGAAAUAUUUUUCAGUUGUUUAUGUCGUUUACUACAAAAAAAAAGAUUCAGAGUGGAUGGAGUACAACUCUGAGUAUUUUUCUAGUCCGGAAUUUUUUAUUAAUAAUCGGUGCUGCCGGGUCAUGCAUGCUGCAACUCUCAACAUUUCCCUUAUUUGGUUCAGCUUUUAGCAAAAAGGGCUACAGUUCACCCUGCAGAGUAUUAAGGUUUCUGGAUUUUUUUCUCCCAACUGUGGCCCAAAAGAAUUAAAAUCUGUUAAUAUAAAUAGAGAACAUAUUUAUCAUUCCUCGAUAGUUAAUUAUAGACUUUGGUACCUUUGUGCCUCAGGGAAGCCACGUGAUAUAACUGGUUAUAGAAUUUCAGGGUUAGGGUUUAAAGAAAGGAGAAAGCCAUUGGAAAAAUGAUGGGCUCCAUUAAGGAGACUAAUGAAUCUGGAUGCAGAAAUAUGUCAGAAACUGGCAUAAACAUGAUUGUAGUAGAAUUUAUUUUCCAGUACCAAUAGGGAAAUUAUUUUAAGUUAUUACAUUUACUGUAUUGGGAAACUUGAGGAGAACUCUUUAGUUCAUAAAGCUUCAAUGUCUUUUUUUUUUUUUUCAUGGAAAAACUCAAACCUCUGUUAUUUGGGAGCUCAGUAUUGUGUGGACACUUACGAGAGUUUUCUGCUUAAUUGAAGUGUAAUAUAGGUUGUAGAAUUGUUACCUGCAGUUCUAUGGUUUUGUUUCACUUCUUUUCUUUUUUAAAGCCAUUCUGUUCUUUGGAUGUGCUUGAAAGGGUGUGUGAUUACACCAUUGUUAAUGCUGGGUAAAAACUAUCUUCUUGCAGCCUUGCCUCAUAACAGUGGAAUUUCUGAUAGACAAACCACAGGACUUUGAUUUUAAGCCAAAUCCAUCUCCAUCCCUUUACUGUCAAUCUUCUGUCCCAGUAGUUUAGCCUUUGUGGCUUAGGUUAUGAUGCGCCUCCUUCUGUGCGACCAAUGAGACGACUUCAGCAUCUUUUUAAAAUAAUCUAAGCAUCAUUGAAGCAGUAACACAAAAAAAAGGUUCAGUAUUUUCUUUUUAGUAUAACUUACAUCCUUUCAAAUAAGUCUUUGCCCUCAUGAAGAAUCCCUAGAGGAAGAUAAGGAAAAUAAGUAUUUUCCAGUUUUGCUUGACAGUUUCUAAACAAACAAAAAUAAACUCAAUGAAAGGAAAGAUGUUUCUUUUUAGCUGAGAUGACAGAUUGCUUCUCUGUAUUAAAUAGUCUAGAAGUUAAGGGGAUGGUCACAUUUACCAUGUAUUGUGUUAUUAGCAGUUAAAUUUUAUGAAUAUGUUUGUAAAAUUGUUGUUUUAUAUUUCAUGUCAAAUUGAAAAGUUUAUUUCUUCACUAUUGUACCUGUGGAAAUACAAGCCAUUUUACAGGAAAAAAUCUUCAAAAACUAUUAAAUGGAUAUCAGCCUGUUUGUGAGCCAUUGUCUUCAGAUUCUGUGGUUGUCACUGAGUUCAUUAGGACAUUUAGUAGGUUGAUACGAGUAGAACUGAUUUUUUUCACUUCUCUAACUUCCAAGUUAAUCUCCAGCUGUUGAGUUUAUUAAUUGUUUUAUAUUCUGCACAAUACAUAUUUAAACCUUGAUUCUGAAAAUCCCCUACAUUUUUUAAUUAAAGAAAUUUCCUUGGUGCCUA